CUACGCUCUUCCAGCUGUCGGACCUGGGAAAUUCUCCUGUGCUAAAUCCCGUGGCGCUCGCGGGUGUCGCCGCGGUGCAUCCUGGGAGUUGUAGUUUUUUCUACUCAGAGGGAGAAUAGCUCCAGACGGGAGCAGGACGCUGAGAGAACUACAUGCAGGAGGCGGGGUCCAGGGCGAGGGAUCUACGCAGCUUGCGGUGGCGAAGGCGGCUUUAGUGGCAGCAUGAAGCGCACCCCGACUGCCGAGGAACGAGAGCGCGAAGCUAAGAAACUGAGGCUUCUUGAAGAGCUUGAAGACACUUGGCUCCCUUAUCUGACCCCCAAAGAUGAUGAAUUCUAUCAGCAGUGGCAGCUGAAAUAUCCUAAACUAAUUCUCCGAGAAGCCAGCAGUGUAUCUGAGGAGCUCCAUAAAGAGGUUCAAGAAGCCUUUCUCACACUGCACAAGCAUGGCUGCUUAUUUCGGGACCUGGUUAGGAUCCAAGGCAAAGAUCUGCUCACUCCGGUAUCUCGCAUCCUCAUUGGUAAUCCAGGCUGCACCUACAAGUACCUGAACACCAGGCUCUUUACGGUCCCCUGGCCAGUGAAAGGGUCUAAUAUAAAACACACCGAGGCUGAAAUAGCCGCUGCUUGUGAGACCUUCCUCAAGCUCAAUGACUACCUGCAGAUAGAAACCAUCCAGGCUUUGGAAGAACUUGCUGCCAAAGAGAAGGCUAAUGAGGAUGCUGUGCCAUUGUGUAUGUCUGCAGAUUUCCCCAGGGUUGGGAUGGGUUCAUCCUACAACGGACAAGAUGAAGUGGACAUUAAGAGCAGAGCAGCAUACAACGUAACUUUGCUGAAUUUCAUGGAUCCUCAGAAAAUGCCAUACCUGAAAGAGGAACCUUAUUUUGGCAUGGGGAAAAUGGCAGUGAGCUGGCAUCAUGAUGAAAAUCUGGUGGACAGGUCAGCGGUGGCAGUGUACAGUUAUAGCUGUGAAGGUACAGUCUGCUCUUGGAAAAAGCAGCCCUGCCCUGAAGAGGAAAGUGAGGAUGACUCUCAUCUCGAAGGCAGGGAUCCUGAUAUUUGGCAUGUUGGUUUUAAGAUCUCAUGGGACAUAGAGACACCUGGUUUGGCGAUACCCCUUCACCAAGGAGACUGCUAUUUCAUGCUUGAUGAUCUCAAUGCCACCCACCAACACUGUGUUUUGGCCGGUUCACAACCUCGGUUUAGUUCCACCCACCGAGUGGCAGAGUGCUCAACAGGAACCUUGGAUUAUAUUUUACAACGCUGUCAGUUGGCUCUGCAGAAUGUCUGUGACGAUGUGGACAAUGAUGAUGUCUCUUUGAAAUCCUUUGAGCCUGCAGUUUUGAAACAAGGAGAAGAAAUUCAUAAUGAGGUCGAGUUUGAGUGGCUGAGGCAGUUUUGGUUUCAAGGCAAUCGAUACAGAAAGUGCACUGACUGGUGGUGUCAACCCAUGGCUCAACUGGAAGCACUGUGGAAGAAGAUGGAGGGUGUGACAAAUGCUGUGCUUCAUGAAGUUAAAAGAGAGGGGCUCCCCGUGGAACAAAGGAAUGAAAUCUUGACUGCCAUCCUUGCCUCGCUCACUGCACGCCAGAACCUGAGGAGAGAAUGGCAUGCCAGAGCAACGACAUAGGGCAGUGGAAAAAGAAUGAGUUUUGGAGUCAAAACCCCUGUUAUCUUGGAAAAGCCAUUUAACUUCCUUGACCUUCAGUUUCAUCUUGUGUAAAAUCAGAAUAAUAAUGCCAACCUUAUAGAGUAAUUUUGAAACUUUUUUUUUUUUUUUUUGAGUUAGAGUCUUCCUCUGUCACCCAGGCUGGAGUGCAGUGGCACGAUCUCGGCUCACUGCAACCUCUGCCUCCCGGAUUCAAGAGAUUCUCCUGCCUCAGCCUCCUAAGUAGCUGGGAUUACAGGCAUACGCCACCACGCCUAACUAAUUUUUGUGUUUUUAGUAGAGAUGGGGUUUCACCAUGUUGGCCAGGCUGAUCUCGAACUCCUGGCCUCAAGUGAUCCGCCCACCUUGUCCUCCCAAAGUGCUGGGAUUACAGGUGUGAGCCACCAUGGCAGCUGUAAUUUUGAAACUUAAUGAGGAUGUAUAUUUAAGUGCUUUGCAAAUUGUGUUUAUAAUGUAUUUGUUAUUUUUACUGUUUAAUUGUCUGCCCCUACCCUGUUCUGGAGAAUCUUGUACCAUCAUUAAAAUAAGUAAAUCCAUAGUGCUAUUAAUCUUGGAACAUUCUAUGUGGAAUUGCCCAUAUGAAAAGCAGUUUGAUUAUGACAGAAUGCCAGGCAGCAGUGUUCCCAUUGUGUUGAAUAAAUGGCAUCCCCACAAUCACAAUCUCAAAUACCAAAAUCAACAAGGAAAAUUCCAAGCAGCUGCCUUUAUAACUUCUGAUUUGUGGGCCACAUUUGAAACCACAGUUUGAUUUCUCAGUCUACAACAUUUUAAUUCAUAGAGCAGGUCUUUCUCUAUUAGCACAUUCUCAAGAUCUUUUGUUGAUCUUGGUUUCAGUUGCUCUGGAGAACAACUGCCUUCCAAAGCUCCCUUUUAAAGUAAAUUUUCUUUUUAAUAGCUAAUUCUAUUUAGAGGUGGACCAAGCCAAGAAUAGCCUCCAAGUUCAGUGACCAUCUUUGCAGUCAUAUACAAGUGAUGCAAUCACAAAAAGAAAGAAACUUAAUUUUAUGCCGCUAGAUAUGAAAGACAGGUAGCUAUGAAUGCAUGGCUCCAGGACCUUCUGCCAUGUCAAAUGAGCUAAACCCUUCCCCGAAAGCCAGCCAGGAAAACGUAUGAUACCAUUUGCAAUGGUAGAAUGUUGCAUGCUGUUCUUCUGUAAUUAUAAUGGCCUGAUCCGUGUGGAGUGGGUGAGUCCUGCUUAACAAUCGUUAAUCUACUGAGUCUUCGUAUCAGCCUCCCAUCUUGAGGAGCAGCAGUUCUUGGCUGGAUGAGUCGGUCUUUGAUUUCAUUAUAAUAAGGAUAGCUUUGUUAAAAUUCCGCUGCGCAGUGGUGCCUAAGGAUUCUGGGAAAAGGUUUUUCUUUUUAUUUUCCCCUUUUUUUGCACGGUGGGGAUGAAUUGUUUCUCUCUCUUCCAUCCCCUAGGUUACUGUUUGUGCUCUCCCUUGAUCUCCUGCUUGUCCCUUUAUUUCUCCACGUUGUGAAAGUUUCUUUCUGUGUGACCAGGAGUCUGUUUAGCAGACCAUAUUGUGAGUGAAGGGCCAGCGUUUGUUGCCUGAUUUUGGCAACGCUGGGUAGUCAGCUGGGAUGUAAUUAAGACUCUGAGAACAGGCUGUCUUCUCCACGGGAAGGGCAUGUUAGAUGGUGCUGGGAUUUGGGGCUGUCAGUUUGGCCAAGGAUGGAGACAGAGAGCUAGGGACAGAGAUAUUUCCUUUCAUUUAUAAUCCCUUUAUGUACAGUGUGUGCACUUGGCAAAGUUUACAUAUAACCUAGUGGCUAGAGCUUACAAGCCAACGCAGUGAAAUUAGCAUAUGUUACAUGUAUUUUUUAGUAAUAUUUUAAAGCAAGUGCAUAUUUCCAAAGUGAAUUAUGCAUGGAUGACAGCAAUAGGGUUGUGUUGCACUGGGUGUCAAAUCCCACAACUUUUUGUCGAGACUGUGGGUUUUACACUAAAAAGGCAGAAAGACUAAACGAAGUAAAACAGUUUUAAUUUUUAACAGUUUGGUUCGGCCCAAGGAGCCGGGCUGUGACAGAUAUAACUGACAUUUGAAUAAUUGGAUUAAUUUAGAGAAGGGCAAAUCCGGUUUUGACGGUUGUGCUUGUGUGUACAUCUUUUUUUAUUAUUAUUUGCAGGAAUGGAGUUGUGUGGUUUAAAUAUACACUUUUUGUGCUGCCUAGCAAAUCUUGAGAAAACAUCACAAAAUUUAUGAAAUUAUCAUUUAAUUAAUUUGUUUUAAUUUAUAUGUAUGUAUAUGUGUGUGUUCACAUAUUAUGCAGCCUUCAUAUGUAUAUAAAAGAAAUUCACCAUAUAUACUUGAUUCGGGUCUAUCAGUGAUAUACAUAUAUACACAUUGCACAUACAAGCACAUUGUAUGUGCACUUAGGAACUUAGUAAAUCCAGCUUGAGAUAAUGUGCAUGACUUCAUAGGAUGUAUAGAAAAUGUGCAGACAAGGAAGCUCACUGUGACAUUGGCAAGCCCCUUUCCUCCCCAUAUCAAUGUGUUGCAAAACAUCACAGUGCAGAAGCAGAAAAGCCUAAUUUGGUAUCUGGGGUAUCAGUAGCCAAAUUCUACAUGGUUGAUUCCUCAGUCCUAAGUUCCUUCAGAUUCAUAUGGCUUUUUAAGUUUCAUAUAUGAAGAUAAUCUUGGCAACAUAAAACCAAGUACAGCACCAUCAUCGCCACCCUCCUCCAGAAAUUCUGGUAAUGAAAUACACCAUCUAAAAUCAGCAGGCCAAGUCUAGGACUCGUGGCAGGCAGUCUUGAAUUGUGGCUGUGGGCUGGCUCUAAGAGCCUUUUCCCCAGCAGGACAUUAAUAGACAUUAACACUCUCGGACAAGAAGUGUUGAUGUGUGGUUUAUAAUGUUAGCACCCAGUUAGGCAGGUAUAACACAUGCUGUAGGAAUCUUGUACCAACACAUGUGUGUGUUGAGUCAGAUUAAUGAGAACCAUAAAAGGAGAGACAUUUCACUUGAGCUGGGGACCUCAUCCUAUCCUUUUACCAAGUAAACCAGUGCUCAGCUGGGUGGCAGUGUCCUGGUGGGAUGUUUUCAAUAUUAGCAUAAGGAGGAUAUUUGAAAGUUUUGUUUUGCUUUGUUGUUAUGUGAUCAUGAAGCCCAAACUGUUAGUCAGUACAGCACAUUCAAACUCCUUUUCAUCUAGUACUGUUUGGCUCAGAGGAAAGGAAACUUUCACGAUAUUCACAACUACACUAUGGGGCAAAAGUUAUUAUUUUCCUCUCUCAGAUUUACCUGACCCUUCUUCAAGUGUUUCUGAAUGAUUCUGAGACACUUUCUGGUUUACUUUGUAAAUGGGGCAAUGAAGCAUUCUUAUCUCCUGACUGGUUCUCCUUAGAGAAUUCUCAAAGCCUUUUAAAAUUGUGUGUUUUUCUGGGGCAGCCUUGAAAGUCCCAGGAGUGAAGUUGCCAUCUGUCCUUUAUAUUAAAAGAAUCUUCUGUAUUGUAUACCUGAUGUGCUUGUCCCAGAGAUAGAUAUUGUUAAUUAAAGGACAGCAUUUGUCCUUUAUCUGAAAUAACUCUCUUGCCUGAAUAACAGUUUCCCAAGCCUUAGGAAACAGGUAAGGACAUUCGGCCCAGAGCCCUGAUGUUUACUAAAGGUCCUUGGUCCAGGAGCUGUCCCUCAGCCUUCACUAGAUCAGACAUGUAGACUAGAAAAUUACUUGCUUAUUUUUUGGGGGGGGCUUGUUUUCUAUUAAUUCAUCUACCAACAUUAUGGCCUUUUGCAUGCGUGUAAGUAAAUGAACAUAAUAUAUACUGUCAUUGGUAGUUUGUGCUUUUUUUGUGGCGACUCACAAACAGCGAGUUCCCAGACAUUCUCACCACACUGCAUCUUUAUGCAAUAGAUGUGACAGGACCUAUAUCCUCCAGUGUCACCUCUCUACUACUGCACACUCUCUGUUUCUAUACCUUCUGCCCCUGGGAAAAGAAAAAUGCAAACAUCUGCCUACAGCAAACAGAGCCAGAGUUCUGCCAGGUGAUAGCUAGAAUAUGUAUAGGGAGAAAGAAAGCCUCGCCCGUAACCUGCUCUAUCUCUGUCUCAGGAAACGCAGAAAAUAAUUUGUCUCUGUAAUAUAGAAAAGCAGUUAGGGUAACGUGGCUGUGAACUGCUGCCUAAAAGUGUGCUGUGUGCUCGCCUCUGUAGUUGCUAAGCACGGAGGAGGAGGCUAGCCAGGGCCUUGCCACAGACUAACUUCAAGAAAAGAGGAAAAGAGUGCACCAGCAGACUCUGGACUGAGGAGCAUGUCCAACGGAGGAGGCGAGGUGUGGCCAAUGGUUCUUUUGUUGAUAAGAAAGACCCUGAAAUUGCCUGUUGCAUGGUGAGGAGAGUAGUAGAUUGGACCGUAAUUUUCUGGUGACCUAACAAACCAAACUAAAGCUCAAGUUUAAUAGGCAAUGAUUCCCGUUUAAAAGGGAAUUCAAAUUAUUUACAGUUCUCCAUCAUCAUUUGCCUCCCUUAAUCAUAUGGACUAGGAAUUGGGCAGGUGACAUACAAGAGGGAAGCCGACUUGGGUGAAAAACAACAGGGGCUGGGCGCGGUAGCUCAAGCCUGUAAUCCCAGCACUUUGGGAGGCCAAGGCGGGUGGAUCCCCUGAGGUCAGGAGUUCGAGACCAGCUUGGCUGACAUGGAGAAUCCCCAUCUCUACUAAAAAUACAAAAAUAAGCCGGUUGUGGUGGUGGGCGCCUAUAAUCCCAACUACUCGGGAGGCUGAGGCAGGGAGAAUUGCUUGAACCUGUGAGGCAGAGGUCAUAGUGAGCCGAGAUUGCACCAUUGUACUCCAGCCUGGGCAACAGGGCGAGACUCCAUCUCAAAAAAAAAAAAAAAAAGAAAAGAAAAAAGAAAAAGACAACAGGGAUGGUGGUGGGUAUGGCAAACAGGUGGGCACUUAUGCUGUCUACAAGGGACAGUUGCUUCCAACUCCAAACAGUUAUUACCUUACAGAGGUGUGGGCCCAGGAUUGCAAGACUAGAUUUUUCGGUGAAAGCCGCCAGUGUGACACUUUUUGAGUUUUCAGUGUUGGCAGAUAAUUCACUGUUUUAAAACAUGCAGAUAAAACUCAACUGUAGUUGGAUGUACUUUACGGGUUGCUAGUUUGCACACACUUAUAUACAUAAUGCAGAACAUAAGUGGGAAUAUUCUAAAUAAUAGACAGUGUGGAAACUUUUCUUAAUAAUAGUAAGAAACUGAGCCCCAAACAACUAUUAAUAUGUUUAGAUGUUUCCCUUUGGGUCUUUAUUUACUGCAUAUACAUUUUAUAUACAUGUUUUAAAAUAGUUGUAAUCAUAGGAGCCUGUGAUUUUUCACUUACUGUUAGAAGCAGUUUCUUUAUAUGAUUUAUAAUGGCUACUGGAUAUUCCAUGUAGAGGAUGUAUUACAAUAUGCAAAAUCAUUUCCUUAUUGUUGGACCUUUAAGUUGCUUUUGAUUUAACAUAGUUAUAAGUAAUGCUGCAAUUACAUAUUUGCUUAUACCGCUUUCUCCUUUUUUUGGAUUAGAUCCUUAGAAUCUAAAAGGAAGAUUACUAAGUCAAAAGAUAUGAACGUUUUUAUGGCUUUUGGUACAUAUUACCAGAUUGCUUUCCAAAAGCGUUGCACCAAUUUACACUGCAAUCAGCAAAGUAUACAUUUAUCCUUGAAGCAUUAUUAUAUUUUUGAGGUUUUUCCUUCUAAACUGGUAGGUGAAAAUUGGACUUCAUUGAUGUUUGAGUUUGCAUUUCUUGAGGUUUUCCCGUUAAUCUGUCGACUAAUUGUAUUUGUUCUUACAACAUCUGUAUUUUCUAAGGUUAAAUUUUGUGGAGGUUUUGUUUGCUUUGUGUAUAUGUGUGUAUUUUUAAAGUUCUCUUUAUAACAAUUGAUAAAUAAUUUGGGAACAGCCCCCUUGGCAAGGCCUUCCUCUAGGGGACCCCCUGUCUCAGCAGUGCUGCAGCUGCUACUUUUAACUGUGUGUUAACUCGGAGUUGGGCCAGGGCCUAAGCAGGAUCCCCUUCCCGAAGAGGGGCUCUUUUGUGUCUGGUGAACCACAAGCUCAGGGCUGUAUCUGCCAAUAUGUUUUUGGCAGAAGCCAUCUAAUAAAAUCCCAUCCGCGCUGUUCUAUGAAAUGCAGUCACAAAUUUGGAUGAUGAUUGCCUGAUGCCAUAUUUUGGUAACAGCUAAUCUCCAUGUCUUAGAUGGUUUUUAUUCAUUGCCUCCCCCCUUCCCUCCUUCACCACUCUGCUUGGUGCAUGUUUUAACGACAAAUGAUGUAUAAUCUGAGUUUCAUGUAGCAUGGUCUAAUGGAAAGGCACUGAGCCAGUCAUAUGGAGACAGGGGUCCUAUUAUUGGCACUGCCCUUUGCUUAAUAAUAGCUUAACAACUACAACAAAUAUUUAUCCUGUGCUGAAAUGCUCUUUCAGCAUUCUUCAUGUAUUCUUGAAUCUUCCUAACAGUCCUGUUAGACAAUAUUAUUAUCCUCGUUUAGGUGAGGAAACUAAGGCUCGGAGUAUUGGAAAUUUCCAGUACUUGUAUUGGAAAGUAUGAUAUUGGACAAGUAUUUUCAAUACGUGUGUUGAAGAUAUUGGAAAUACUUGUCCAAUAUCAUCCUUCAUCUCUCUGAACUAAAAAUGAGUUUUUUAUUUCUAGUAAUCUGUCUCCCCAUCUGCAAAAUGGAGUUGCUUCUCUUCAACUCAGAAUGGUGGCAUGGAACUAAAAUGAUGCCAUGUAGAUAUUAAGUUGCCUUGAGUAUUGAAAUCCAAGACAAUAAAUUGGUAAUAAUAUGUAGUUAUUAACUAGUUCACCUCUGUGACUCUCAGCUUCUUCAUUAAUUAAAUGUAGGGACUGAACCAGAUUCAUUUCAUUGGUUACUUUCAGCUAUCACAUUUUCCCAUCAGCCACAGACUCAAAUGUUGGUGGAUAAAGCCUGCGUGGUUCCCAGAGGCUGUGCAUACUGCCUACAUUUCAAUCAGCUCUACAUUUUAGGUACAUCCAUCCCUCUCAGCUAGUGUUCUUAGGAAGAAAAUGCAAACUUUUAGGAAGGAGAAAUCUCACUCUUCAGUGUUUGUGGAGAGUGCAGGGAAAUUCUCUUAAUGGAAUAGUAGAGAUACCAUUGUCUGACAGCCACUGUAAAGCCAUAUGGAGCUGCUUGCUUUUGGCUCUGGAGAUAUUGUGACCUCUUAAAAUAUAUUUUUCUAAAAAAGGAACAUGCCUUAUUUCUGUUUUUCUUUAUACUUCAUCCCCAGGUAGGAAUUUAACCAAGAUGGUUAACGGAGAAAGUAAGGCAUUGACUCAGCUCCAUACAAAAAUGCAUUCUGGCUUGUUUGCAUAAAUAUCACAGAAAAAUAGGGGUUCAGGAUCCCAUAUGGCACUUAGCCUCCUAAGCAAAGAUCAUCAGCCAUAGACAAGAAGCAGGUGGCCUGGCAUCGAGAGCAGAGGUUAUUUUUGCUGCUGGGCUCCCGCCAUUUCAGAGUUUAACAGUGGCAAGUCUACUCAGCAGGAGGCUGACCCCAGAUGCUCUCCCCUUGUCGGACAUGGAGCCGUCCCAUGUCCCACCUCCACUGCUGGGAGUAAACCUGAUCAAAUCUAGGCCACAGUUAGACUCCCAGAUAAGUCUCUGUUUAAGCUUAUUCCCAUUUGCUACUUAAAUACCACUUCCAAAUCUGAUUCAUUUGGGGUGAAGUCACAGACUUAAUUGUUCACCCAUCCUGGGUGGCUCUUGAAAGCCUGUGAUAAUGAUAUCUUGGCAUUUUCUUUUAGGUGAACCCUAGUGCAACAGGUUGGAAAGGGCUAGUUUUGAGGAUAGUGUUAGAGACCAGAGGUGUGGAAACCUGGAUUCUGCCUCUGGUUCUGCCUCUCCCUAGAGCUCAGUCUCACUGUGUGUAAUAUGAAGAGAUUUGGACCGUGUCUGGGGUUUCAAAUUCAGUUGCCAACAGGGAAGUAUAAAAAAUGAAUGAGAAGGGAAAAGAAAGGAAGAGGGAGACCCAGUGGAAAGGUGCAUGAGGGAACUUUGGGGCGAGUGUGAAAAUGCAUAUCGUGAUUGGUUGAUGGUUAUAUGGGCAUAUACAUUUUUCAAAACUUGUAGAACUUAUACUAAAGAUCUGUCCACUUUACCGUAUGUAAAAUAAGUGUAAAAUGAGUGAAAUGGACUAGGUAGUAAACUGCAGAGCAUAUACCUCAUUUAAAAGGGGCGAAUGAUAAGCUCUAGCCAAUGGCUUCUCUUCAGAAUAGAGGCCCAGUGUUGCUACAUUUUCAAGUAAAGCCAGAAAUUCACAUAUUUAUAUAAAAUCUCAGGAUAUGUAGAUUUAUGGGCCCUGCUUGGUCAAACAAAAUGCCAGUUUUGUGAUCUCUGAACUUUGGGCUUCUUAAUUUGAGUCUGAGGAUCAUUUUAGCUUCAACAUUGGAUGAUGCCGACUUGCGGUGAGACCUCAGACAAAAAGAUUAAACUUGCCUACACCUCAGUUUUUUUCACCUGUAAGAUGUUGAUAAUUCAUGACUAAUAGUACAGGGGUCUGAUGAAGAGCAUAUGAGGUACCUUGUACAAAGCCACUUUGAAACAUGAAUAAAUAACAUAAAAAUGCAAGUCACUAUUACCUUUUUUAUUAUUAUAAAGAAUUAUUUCCGUUUUUAGAAUUGUUAUUGUUCAGAAUUGAAGCACUAAACUUAGUAAAGAUGGCUAAUAAAAACAUCAAGAUUCACCAUGAGUAAAUGACUUGCCUGCAAAUGAUCAUGCAAACCUUUCACUAUCCUUAGAGGGGAAUGUUUCUGUUGUGUGUGACAAGAAGAAAAGGCAUUUCAUUUGUACAGCUACUCAUAUAAAUUGCAAAAACCAUGGGAGCUGAAGUCCAAGGUACAGCAAUAGCAUAUAACGAAAUGAACUUGAUGCUGUAUUAAAGAUUCUUUGUCACACGCACUCACUGCCUAGGAGUCGUAAUGCUCCCAGCCUUGUCACUGACAUUUUGUGAACAAGCAGCCUGUAUUGGAUGGUGAUAAAUGGAUUAUCUUAAAUGUCAUUCUGCACUGUUUUAGAGUUGCAAAGAGAGUUUUGAUAUUGAGUUUUUGGUUAGUAUAUUCUGUAUCAAUCCUUUCUGAUGAAAUAAUCUCCUCAAGUUACAUCCAGAAAUGUCAAAGUUGCUUAUUUCUUCAAUCACCCAUAGCAAUGUUUCCAUUACAACGUAUGCAGAGAAGAUUGUGUAAUAAUGUCAAACUAUUUAUAGAAACAUUUCCUAGGAAUCUCUACUCUCCUUGAGUUGUUUGUGUAUUUAAUACUAGAGAUUUGUUUUUAUAUGUAUAUAUAUAUUUCUAUUUCUAAAUUGACUUCAGCUGAGGAUGUUGUACUUUAGUUUUUAUAUAGAGCACAUUGAAAACUUGGUAAUAUUAGCAUUCGACAACUAAAACUAAAGCCACGCUAACAUUUUGUAAAUAGAAAGAGUCACGUAUUUUGGUUUUAAAUAUUGUAAGUUUUUUUUUUUUUGGUGUUGCAGUUGCAGCUGUGUCCUAAAGGUUGUAAGGUUGUUAUAUUCAUAACAAAUUUAAACCUAUUUAUUUAGUCUAAAGUAGUAUGGAAUACUUUGCCCAAAGAAGUUUUCAUAUUUAUUUUAUGCUAAUUUCUCCAUUAUUUUAUCUUUAAUAUUUUUUGACUUUCCAAAUUUAAUACAAUUAUUGCUAUUACACAGAAUUUAGUCAUUUGUAUAAAGAUUUGGUCUGGUGGACUUGUGUGGAAAGAAGCACAAAAUAGAUUUUGAAAGCAUAUCUCACAUUUUACUUGGCAAAGUUAUUCUAAAUAUUGGCUUUCUUCCCUAAAGAUAAGAUCUUUCUAGAUACAGAUAUUGAAAAUACUCAGUUAGCAUAUACCGAGUGGCUCCCUUCAGACUCUCUGUACUCUACGAAUCUUACCCUCAUCCUGUCAUUCUACAGUCCUCAAAAAAAAAAGACAUGUAAUUUAUAUUUUAAAAAUCCAAACAAUAUAAAUAAUAUUAGAUUGGACCAUAUAAAAUUACUAUUUUUUGUAGAUCCAAACAGUCACAUAGGAGCAAUUUUAUGUGGCUCACCCAAGCAAUGAAGAUUUAUAUUGUAUUUACUACAUGCCAAACAUGUGCUGGAUGUAUAUGAAUUCAUAUACUGAUUAUAGCAACCCUAUGAGUAGGUGCUAUUAUUUCCCCUAACCUACAGAUGAAAACUUUGAGGCACAGAUUGAUUAAGUAAGUAUCAGAACCAGGCAGCCUGCCACCAGAGUCUUUGCUGAUCAUCAGGACUCUGUGCUACCUCUCCAAAAUAGCAAAGUUCCCUGGCUCUCCCACCCCAGUGUAGUGCUUUUCACUGUAAAAAUUUAAUGAUGUCUUUCAUCUUACAUGUCUUAAUGUGAUAUUCCUUUCAGCUAUUCUAAUCAAAUAUAUUAUUCUUUUCUCUUACAGUUUUUGUGCAUUAUAUCUUUCUUAAGAUCAACUUUCUUUAAAAACUAUGUUUUUAAAGAAAUUCACUUUAAUGGAAUUCUGAUGCUUUCAUAGUUUUGUUUUCAGUGUUUACCUAUUUAAUCCACCUGAACUUUACUUUUGUGACUGGUUGUUGAGUAGGGAUUAACUUUAUUAUUAGGUUUUCAAAUGGACGGGCAAUUGGCACAACACCUUUUAUGGAAUAAACCAUUCUUGCCUCCACUGAUUUGAAAAGACACUUUUAUCAUAUACUAAAUUUGCAGAAAUUUAUGUGUCAGGUUUUUUUUUGCCUAAUUACCAAAACUUUGUGUGUUUUUAGAUAUUAUAGGGCCUUCCCUCCUCCAUUUUCUUUUUAGAAAAUUUCGUUAACUGUUUUCAUGCCCUUUUUGUCAGAUGAAUCUUAGAUUCCGAUAGUCAGAUUCCAUAAAAAAUUUUAAAUCCUGUUGGCAUUUUAAUAUAAAUGCAUUGAAUUUAUAGGUAUAUAUGUUGGAGAAUUUUUUAAAUGUCACCUCAUCUAUUAACAUGUUUUAUUUCUUCAUUUAUUUAUGUCAUCUUUUGUGUUCUUAAAUGAGUUUUAAAAUUUUCUUCACAUUCUCCUUUAUUUCUAGAUAUUUGUGUUUAUUGCUGUUGUAAUGGAAUUACAGAUAUGUCUGGUAGCUGUUGAGUUUUUGCAUUCAUAUAGUUACCUUACUAAAUUUUAUUAGUUCUGGUAGUUUUUCAUUUGAUUCUUCUGGAAUUUCUAAGUAAGGAAUUAAAUAAUCCAAAAUAAAAUGAUGUUGCCUUUCUCUCUCCAAUGUACUUUUGUUGGUCUCUUUUUCCUGUCUUGGCUGAUAUUUUUUGGAAUAAUGUUAACUAGUAGUAGGGAUAAUAGGCACCCUUUGAUUUUUUUUCCUGUUGUUAAUUAGGAUAUUUCAAAAGUUUUGCAGUUAACCUGGAGAUUUGCUGAGAUUUCUGAUCAAUAUCCUUUAUUAAGUAAAAUAAUUCUUAUUCUCUUUAAUUCUCUUUAAUGGUUGUUGCAUUUAAUCAGAUAUUGUUUUGAGGGGAGGAGGUUAUCUACUGAGAUGAUGACAUGGGUUUUCUCCUUUGUUCUUUAAAUGUGGCCUAUUACAUUAUUGGAUCUUAUAUUGUUGAAUCAUCUUUCCAUUUCUGAAAUAGAGCUUACUGUAUCUUGAGGUAAUAUAUGCAGGAACUUAAUUUGGUGACAUUUUAUAUAUAAUUUUCUAUAGGUGAUAUUUUUCUAUAGCAGUAUUUUCUGAUGCUCUCUGACCCUGGUUAACAGGUCUCAGUAGAACUCAUUCAUUCCUAACAUUUCUGUGAUGUUACUGUUUUGAAGCUUAUCCAAAGCUUGAUUGGCUUUUGAUUAUUUUAGCAUUAAGGCUUUUGCAUGCAAUUUCCCUCAAAUCUUUGAAGUUUAUUUCUGUUUAUAGCUUUCCUUAGGAAAGGCAUGAGUUUACUCUUUCAACUUUUUUGCUCUUGCCUCCUAUCUUCUUUAUGGGGAGAGAGUAUACAUAUUUCUUUGAAGCAUGAUGAGUAUAAAUAUUUCUUUGACAUCUUUAUGAAACCUGGAAUUGUCUCUUUUCAUUUGGAAAGAAAUAAACUUUUCUUGCUCAUCAUUCUUUAUGCAUAAAACUAUAGUUUUAGUUAGUCCUGAUUUAUAUGCAGUGUUCCCCUAGAAAGAGAUAUUUAUUUAUUUAUUUAUAGACAGGGUCUUGCUUUGGUGUUCAGGUUGGAAUGCAGUGCUGCAAUCAUAGCUCACUGCAGCCUCAAACUCCUGGGCUCAGAGGAUCCUCCUACCUGUCUCCCAGGUAGCAAGUACUACAGGCAUGCACCACUAUGACUGGCUAAUUUUUAAAAAAAUUUUUUUUGUAGAGAUAGGGGUCUCACUGUAUUGCCCAGGCUAGAUAUUUAGUAUUUUAUAAUGAGAAACAGUGAGGUUAGAGAAGACACUAUUGUUUCAUUUUAUGCAUGUAUGUCACCCUUGGCAAAUAUCACUAAUCUCGAUGCACAUUUUCCUUCUAAACUUGUAUAUAGCCUUCUUAACAUGGCACACCAAAUAGUUACUACCAAUUGAUUGGUACUUGCAAUUUAAAUGAGACCUAUUUGCACCCCCUAGUAUGGAAACAGCAGUCUUUGGAUGCCAGGAGUCCUAAGCUUUCAGUCUCUAAUUUGCAGUGUGAAACAUCAAGCUAUUUCAAAAUUUAAUCUUAGUUUUCACAGCUAUACAAUGAAGAGAUUAAACUGGAUAAUAUAAUGGAUUUUCUGAUUCUGUUUACAUAUGCUCCUUCAUUAUUUCAGGGCCAAACAUCGUUUUAGGUUUUGUAAAUUACGACUAAACUGUGUAUUUGUAACUUUAUUAUUACUAUUUUGUUGUUUUCUUGUUCAUUUGUGGUUUUGAGAUUGUAAAUACAUCUGCCAUUUAGCUAAUUCUCUUUUGUGGCCAAGUACUUUUUCUUACUUUUAAAAUUAAUAAAGGCUCAUUGUAGAAAAUUUGAAAAUUGUAGAAAAGCACAAAAGGAAAAUAAAAAUUACCCAUAAUCACCGGGUGCGGUGGCUCACAUCUGUAAUCCCAGCACUUUGGGAGGCCAAGGUGGGUGGAUCAGUUGAGGCCAGGAGUUUGAGACCAGCCUGGCCAACAUGGUGAAACCCCUUCUCUACUAAAAAUACAAAAAUUAGCUAGGCAUGGUGGCACACGUGCCUGUAAUCCCAGCAACUCGGGAGGCUGAGGCAUGACAAUUGCAUGAACUCAGGAGACAGAAGUUGCAGUGAGCUGAGAUCAUGCCGCUGCACUCCGGCCUGGGAGGUAGAGCGAGACUCUGUCUCAAAAAAAAACCAAAAAAGUACCCAUAAUCCUACCACCCAGAAGGUUAACAUUUGGUUAUGAUUAGAAAUAUUUCUGUUUUUAAAAUCGUUAUACUCUUUUUCAUAGAAUAUUAUUACAUACAUCACUGAAAAAUAAUUUUCCUCAAUAUAUACAAUCAUUUAUUUUUAUCAUAUCUCUUUAGGGUUUCACUUUUAAAUAUUAUGACAGACAUCCUUUUAUAAGAAUCUUUGAGGCUUUCUUGAACAGAUUCCUAGAUAUGGAAUUACUAGGUAAAGGAGAGUGUACAUUGUAAGUUCCUAACAAAUUACAGGUUCUUGAAAAAUAUAUCUGGAAUGGAUGUUUGAAUAAAAUAUUGCCAAUUUGAUUUCUAGAAAGAUGGACCAAUUUACAGAUUCAUCAAGAGAGAAUGCCUCUCCCAUCUCAAGUUUGGCAGCAUGGAAUAUUACAGUUUGAAAACAUCUUUUCCAAUUUUAUGGACUAAAAGUAACAGAAUUUCUUUAUCACUACUGUGAUUGGAUCUUUUUUAUGUUUAUGGCUGUGUGUGUGUGUGUGUGUGUGUGUGUGUGUGCGCGCGUGUGUGAAUUUCUUGUCCUCUACAUUUUCCCCUUCCUUUUGUGGCGUACAUGUUAACUGUUAACAGCUGCAGUGCCUAUGAGCUCAUUAUCAAAGUGUUGCUCCAUAAUUUACAAUUAUACCUAACUUUGGGGGCAAAAUCCCAAUUUGGAGGUCAAAAAGAGACCAAAGUCUCUGUACAUCUCACAUGACUUUACUUGCAUUAACUUUGCCUUCCUAAAUUACAGUCUAUAAUUAAGAAGUGCUAGUCUCCUGGCCAGCUCUUAUGGUUAUUUUUGAAGCUCCUUGGGUGCUUGCACCCUUCCAGAGGGCUGUUACUUUGCCCCCUCUCUGGAAGCUCAUUUGCUUCCACAGGAAGCCUUAAGCCAAAGCACAUUGGCUUAUUCAAUCUGGUGUCUGGAUCUUAAAACCUGGCUUCUCAGUUUAUGAUGCUCACCAGUAAAACACUCAUGGCUCUUCUUGCCAUGAAGCGAACCAGGCUUGCUUAGCUUAGCUUCAUGUGUGGCCUUCGUGAAUCAAAAUAAGAAGAAGGUAGAACUAGUCCCACCCUUAAGUCAAGAAGAACUGGUUAGUCAUGAAGUGAAGCCACAUGACUUUGCUCUUUUCUAUUAUGUCUUCUAAUUGUUUCUGACAAGAAUCCCUGGAUUUCUCUCACACUCUUCUAGCUUGAUGCUAUUGGGCUCCUUUUACCGAACAAUUGUGAAAUUAGUAACUAACCUCUGCUUGCUGAUGAGAUUGUUUGACAGCCGUUUGCUACCUGGAAACCAGAAUGGCUGGAAAGAGACCUGUUUAUGCAUUUUUCAUGUUAAAUGCUAGGCAAAGAGGUUAUACCCUACAUGUGGACUCUAAGCUAAGGAAGCUGACACGUGGGGAGGGAAAAGGGCUGAAAUCCAAUGCAUACGCCCCUCUUCAAUCCUGGGAGAUUGUAUUUGCCCGUCAGAGGCACCUUUUUCUAAUUUGCCCAGAGGUGCUGAAAAGGCGGCUGAGGCCCUGCUCAACUGCCUGAACAACUUACAGAAGCACCUCUCCUUCCAACCAGGUUAGGAUCCAAAAAGCUGUAUGUAAAACCUCUUGUUUAUAAAUCCAAGGUGGCAUUAAGCAGCCACUGGGAGUAUGAUCUGUUAGGGACAGGCUUUUGCUCCAGUAUUUAGGCUUGUUCUUAUCAGUAAAUCUAAAUAGAAAGUUCCUAAGUAAAGAAGCUUCCGUAUUUAAAUAGCUCAAAAUACGACAGCCUUAUUUUUUUAAUAGCGGCAUUGUUUCUCUUUCCCAAAGCAACCAUAACUGAGACAGGAUUAGAUGCAAAAACCACUUGCUGAUACAGUUUAGAAUUGCAAAAUUCUAAAUUCCAACAGAUUCAUAUUAUACACAAGUAUAAACAGAGUGUAGCCAGUUUUCCUCAAAGAGAUAACAUGGGUUCUCCACAGUAUUUUUGACCCAACAAGCCAUUAUUAAAUUUGGAGAGAAAUUUUUGCCUGGGAACCUUGGCUCACACCUGUAAUCCAGCAUUUUGGGAGGCUGAGGCAGGAGGAUCACUUGAGGCCAAAAGUUUUGAGACCAGCCUGGGCAGCAUAGCAAUGCUCUGUCCAUACAACAAGUUUAAAAAUUAGCUGGGUAUGGUGGUGUGUGCCUGUAGGCCCAGCUAAUCAGAAGGCUGAGGCGGGAGGAUCGCGUGAACCCAGGAGGUUGAAGCUGCAAUAAGCCAUGGUUGUGCCACUGCAUUCCAGCCUAGGCAACAGAGCAAGACCCCAUCUCUAAAACAAAUGGGAGUAGAGUUCUAAUGGCAUCCAAAGGUAAAGGCCCAUAUUCCCUGGUGUUCCCCAAAUCAUUGCAACAAAAAAGCAAAGCCAUUUACCCUCUAAGUAAUGUCAGUAAACAAUGAAGGAAAACCUGAAGCCUUCCUGCUUAAGAGCCAUUCUGAGGCCUGGCAUGGUGGCUCACGCCUGUAAUCUCAACACUUUGGGAGGCCAAGACGGGCGAAUCACCUGAGGUCAGGAGUUUGAGACUAGCCUGGCCAACAUGGUGAAACCCCAUCUCUACUAAACAUGCGAAAAUUAGGUCCGGGUGCGGUGGCUCACACCUGUAAUCCCAGUACUUUGGGAGGCCGAGGCGGGCAGACCAUCUGAGGUCAGCAGUUUGAGACCAGCCUGGCCAACAUGAUGAAACCCUAUCUCUACUAAAAAUACAAAAAAUUAGCCGAGCGUGGUGGCAGGCACCUGCAAUCCCAGCUCGUCAUGAGGCUGAGGCAGAAGAAUCGCUUGAACCUGGGAGGCGGAGGUUGCAGUGAGCCAAGAUCGCACCACUGCACUCUAGCCUGGGCAACAAGAGUGAAGCUCUGUUUCCAAAAAAAAAAAAAAAAAAUUAGCUGGGCAUGGUGGCAUAUGCCUGUAAUUCCAGCUACUCAGGAGGCUGAGGCGGUAGAAUCAUUUGAACCCAGGAGGUGAAGUUUGCAGUGAGCCAAGAUUGUGCCACUGCACUCCAGCCUGGGCGACAGAGCGAGACUCUGUUAAAAAAAAAAACAAAAAACAAGACAUUCUUAGCUUCAUUUCAAUAUCUCCAUCCUAAGCCUUAGAGAAAACUUCAGUCCUCACCUCACCACAUUCUGUUAUUAGAAGGCAUUAAGAAGGAGGUGUUCUAAGUUCUUCUCAACCUUAUUGAGGAUGAAGGUGAAGGGUUGUACCCUUACAAUAGGGCAUGGUAUACCUCCAAUACACCUCUUUUCUUUUGUCUGCCCAUGUUUGUGACUAUGAUGUCCUAAAGCACUUUAUGUGAGACUUAGAUUUUCUUUUUUCAUGGUGUAAGUUAAAUAUGAAGUAAUCUUGAUUAGGCCUUUUGUUCACAGAACCAAUGAACUGAUGAAAACCUUGAUGAUAUUCAUGUGUCUAAUGUUAUCAUCGGAGGGGUUUCAGUGAAACAGCUUAACUUUAGGUUCAGAGAGGUUUCAUUCUCACACCAGAUCCAGAAGUUACUAUUAUAAUACCUGCUUGCAUGAACUUGUUCAUGGUACUCACUGGUACAAAUUUAUGGCUUCAAGUGAUAGAAUGCUCAGUAAUAUUGCCCUCUUGGAAGCUGUGCCCAAGAAACUUAGUUUCCUAACUGGGCUCUGCAGCUGUUGAAACUUCAUCACCUUUCACCUGAAUCUCUACAAUGCUUUGCAAAUGAGGAGCUGGUGAGAAAAAUAUGCAGCUCGAAGCUGGCAAAGUUUUAAGUGGGUAAAGCUUGCAGUGUUAAGAUCAUAGCCCCAAAUUACUUAAGGGCUUCUGCUAACAUGAAAAUAAGACUCUUGACUGCUGAGAGAUUGGAUAUUCAGAUAGAUUUUUUUAUGAAGGAAAUAAAUAUUUCAACAUGCAAACACUACCCAAGCGGGUAGUGAUGCUUCAAAACAGGGUCAGAGGUCAGGUUUUUUUCUGUUUGUGUUUUUUGGGAUGGCUCCAAGUUUAAAGGUAUUACACAUCACUACCUACCCCGAGCCUCACAUGGUAAAGUAAUUACUGCUAGCUAGCGGAAAAUAUGUACAUUCAUUUUUAUUUCCAAAGAUCCUGAGAUUUCUCUCUGCGCUUUUUGUGGUCCUCAUUAUAAAAAAUAUAUCAUGAAGAAUGAUGGUUUUUCUCCAUCCUAACGGUAAAAGAGUCAAGCUGAAAAUGCAUGUCUGAUACUCAACUUUUUUAACAAACUUAAUUUUGGAGGAAUAAAUAAGCAUAGAAUGUAUUUAUUCUUUAGAGAAUAGUAGAGUUCAUUUUUAUAGUUUGCCUUUAAAACAUGCAACAGACCCCUAGGGUAUUGGAUAAUUUUUAGAGGAGAUGCUGACCUGGUGGUCAGCCAUUUUGACGGAACUGGGGCCCAGGAUAUCUUCAGGCAAGCAUAAAGAUGUGUGGCAUACAUUGUUCUGAAACUUAAACACUGACUUUCUCAGUGGAGUGGAAUUUGGGUGACUGUUGGAAUUGCUAAACAGGACUUAGAGUUUCAGAAACCCUUUUCUCUCUGCCUUCAAGUAGGGAAAAUAAUUAUUUGCUGAGCAAUUAAUUCGAAUUCACAAACACACACACACACACACAUCAGAUAUGGUAAGCUCAGAUCUCUGCAGAAGCCGGCAGGUAAUGUCAACGAGUGAAGCAGGGGUUGGUGUAAUACAUUAGGGAGUUGUGGGGACAAGAAAGAACUAGAAAGCACACCCCCGGUCUAAGAGGACAACCAGCACUCUGCUCCCAGCCAGCUGCUGCCAUGAGAGAAUAUGGGCCCACUGUUGUGUACGGCUCAGGGUUUUUGUUUUCUGUUUUUCCAAAAGAAGCCAGAAAUCCAGAUGUUUGUAUGAAAGGUAUUUUUAUAAAAAUUUUGACAACUAAUAUAAAACACUAUUUGAAAAUGUAUUUGAGGGCUAGCUUUGGCCUACAAGCCACUAGGUUGUAACUUCAGCUUUCAAAAAUUGCAAAAGGUAGAGCCAGCUGCUUAGUGGCCAUACCUUCUCAUUCUCCAAGGGAGGUGUUUGGAGCCUGGUGCAUUCUAAACAAUGACUGUUCUGUGGCUUAAAACCCUAUUGUGAAGAACACAGUUACUCUGAAAUUGAGGGCAGCUUGUCUCAUUUAUAUCAUUUCUUUUUAGUGACACAGAUCCUUCGUUAAGGCCAACUUUUAAGGGAGUCAAGUUGCAGAAAAGUUUACAGGGCAUAACCACCCUCACCUUGCUUUUCUUACUGACUUUUAACCAUCACAAAGUAAUUACUUUCCCUCCUCUAUCCCUCCCUUGGAAUGGGUCUUUUUUUUUUUUUUUUUUUUUUUUUUUGACUCACUCUCUCGCCCAGGCUGGAAUACAAUGAUGCCAUGAUGGCUCACUGCAGACUCGACCUCCCCAGCUCAAGUGAUCCUCCCACCUCAGCCUCCUGAGUAGCAGGGUCUACAGCGCCCACCACGAUACCUGACUACUUUGUAUUUUUUUGCAGAGACAGGGUCUUGCCAUGUUGCCUAGCCUGGUCUCAAACUCCUGGGCUCAAGCCAUCCUCCUGCCCCAACCUCCCAAAGUAUUGGGAUUACUGGCGUGAGCUACUGUGCCCAUCCAGAAUGUGUUACUUUUUAAAGUACAUUGUGAGGCAGGACAGUAUUCACAUUGCCUUUCCCAGAGCCCCUAAAGCAUCAACUGAAGAUGGUGUCCCUACUGCAGUCAAACAGAAAUGCUGAGUAAUGACUGGUUUAAUAAUGAUCAGAUAGACGAGAAAAGGCCUUGACUAAGUCAGUGAUAUUGGGAUAUGAUUAUUUUAAUUAUUUUAAUAUUGAUUCUUUUGGUGUCUUUUGGAUUGUUUAGCUGUCGCUUUUUCUCUUGGCUUUUGAGGUUUCAGGACACGGAGUAAAAUGAUGGAAAUGUGUUUGUUUUUCAGGGCAGAGAGGAGUGUUGGUAAGUAGAGAAAUUACAUUGUGUCCUCAGCUGCCAUUGAUGUCCUUCCAAAUAGGUGAAGUUUAGUUUAAAACCUGCCGUUAAUUUCUGGCCUCUGGCAAGAGUGGUACAAGGUUACCUGUUUGUUCCAGUAUGUGUAGGGAGGGGCUGGGGGUUGGGGAGAGAGAAGGGUGGCAAUUAGUCAAUGACAUUUAUGACCCAUUUAUAAAAUACAAAUGAAAUAAUUGGUUACAAAAUCAUGACAAGCCUUCACUUGUCUUUUACAAACUUGUUCUCAACACACUGUGAAACUUAAUGGACACCCUUUGUAGAAAGUGAGGAACAACAGCCAUUCUGAAGAGACCGAUUCAAAGCGUUCAACCUGAGACUAGCUGUGGUGGCGAAGAUUCUCUGAGUAUGUUUCUCAUUCUCAUCUCAGAUACCCGCAUUAUUAUCGCAGAUCCAGAGGCAGGGAAUUUGUAGAUUCCUCAGCCAGGGAAUUGCCACAGUUUUGGUGUAGGAUGACCAGACAUGAGAAAGAAAAAAAUUUUCCCACAAAUCUUUAAAUGCAUGGGACCCUUUGGGGUCUUUGCUGAGAUUAGAGCACUGUGUGUUUAUAAAUAAAAGAAGAAUAAACAAAGGCAGCAUGCACUGGCAGUCCCCUCCUUCCUGCCCUGUUAAAAUGCUGUGUGAGGUGGCAUCGAGAAAAUGAACGCCAAGGUUGACACCAAAUGUAGGGCCCGAGUGAUUUUUCUGUUUUUCAAAUCCGCUGUCAGUUCUCCACCUCUGACUCUUAGUCUUUUUCUCCUUCCCCACCUCUAGAGAGAGGACAUUUCCUGAGUAAAAUGAAAAUCAAAGCUAGGAGCUAAUCAUAUUUUUAAAGUCAGAUAUGUUGGGGGUAUAACUGGAAGCUAAUUUUUAAAAGAAUCCUGCCAUAUCUUUGAUAAGGAAGUUCUAUGGCUUAAAGAGUGUAACCACUAGUUUUAGCAGAGAUGUUUCCUUUAGUUUUGAAACAUUCUUCAACAUUUCAGGUUCAUGAUGAAAAAUGGCUGACUGGAUUUAAGUCCUUUAUUUUCUAUACUCCUGAGCAAAAUUCUGAAAAACUGGCUGGUCUAGUUUAGAGAAGAACGCUGAUGUGGGAGUAUUUUCACCAUGCAUUCCUGCUCUAAAUCCUUUGCUUCUACUGAUAGACUAUUCUACUUUCGAAAUAAGUUCACAUUGCUCUAACACUUCAUAAGUUCAAUCUUUUUCUCAUUCUGUUUAAAAUAACCACCAUGACCACCAAACGCCUGAAAUUCACUGUAGUUAAAAUUAUGACUGAAAUAGACAGGGAAAACCUGAGAGUGAACGUUACCCAGCAAAUCUGGGUUAAACAGGUUCGAGUUUUUCCAGAGCACACUGUUUAGGAUUUCAGCUUCCUGUUCAACCAUCUCGGAAACAGGGUGUUUCUCUGCUCCUUUGUGAGGACUAACCAUGUGUCCCCGCCACUUUGCACCAAAGCUGAAUAUCAUCCCAAACUCUGGAUCCUUCUGACGGGCAUUUGUGUGGUACACAGGAAGGGGUGCAUUAUGAAUAUGCAAUUACUGGCAUGUAAUGCUGUCUUCUGCUAAAAAUACAAAAAGGGUACUCUGAUCUCAGAGUUGGGAGCUGAUUUCUGAUUUCAGCCUAGACAGGUCUGCUUAAAACUAUAAUCAAGCUGAUUGUAUUGCCCUGGAAUUCUAAUUUCCAAUUUAGGGUUUUGCUAUAUAAUCUCUAGUAGAGUGUGUCUAAUCUUUAUGAAACCCAGAGUCUUUGUAUAAACUCUAUGGAUUUUCUUCCAUGCGUCUAGGCUGAGCUGAGCUGUGUCUUUAGGCUGAGCUGUAGAGACAUUAAAUUACUGAGUAAAUGAAGGUAACGUUGUUAUGUCACUCUGUUUCUGAAAGACCAACUCAAAUUCUGUCUGCUGUAGCUUUGAUCCUUUUCAUUUAAUUCUAAGUACACUUGUUAUUAUAGUAACUGUUGUUUGUAUGUUAUUUUAGCUUUUUACUUAAGUAGCUAUUUAGCAAUUUAAAUGAAAAUGUAAUUAGGUUACAUCUGUUUUACAUGCAUGUAAUACCACGCAGAUGUAAACUUCUAUUAAAGCCAUAUUUUCUUUUUGGCAAGAAAAGGCAGAAACAAAAUCGUGCCAGUCGCUGGAAUACGUCUUGCUCUAAAAAAAUUAAAAAAAAGGAUAUACAGAGCACUGUGCCAUUAUUUAUAUGGUGGUUAGAGUACAUCACUUCUAUUUUUUGAAAAUUAAAAAAAAUAUUAACAAGUGAAAAACAAGCAUUCUAUUCCAUGUUCCCUCUUACAGUUUAUCUGGAUACGGUGUUUAAAAUGACAAUACAGCCAGGCGCGGUGGCUCACGCCUGUAAUCCCAGCACUUUGGGAGGCCGAGACAGGUGGAUCACCUGAGGUCAGAAGUUCAAGAUCAGCCUAGCCAAUGUGGAAAAACCCCAUCUCUACUAAAACUACAAAAAAAUUAGCUGGGCAUGGUGGCAUGCGCCUGUAAUCCCAGCUACUCGGGAGGCUGAGGCAGGAAAAUUGCUUGAACCCAGGAGGCGGAUGUUACAGUGAACCGAGAUUGCGCCACUGCACUCAAGCCUGGGCCACAGAGAAAGACUCUGUCUCAAAAAAAAAAAAAAAGAAAAGAAAAGAAAAAUGACAGUAUGGCUUCCCCCCAUUCUAUGGGUUUGUGCACACAGAAAUACACCCAUCCUCCCAUCAUAAACACUGGUUCUUCCAACUCCACAGAUAGUGGAAAGAGUCAAGAAGCAGCCGAGAUUCUAACCUAGCUCUGCUUUAUGACUUUGGUAAAGCCAUUUUACUCUUCAGUAUUAUUAUUUUUUAAAACCAAGAGUAAUAUUUGCCCAGUUUGCCUCAUAGACAUGUUGUGAGGCUCAAGGGAGAUAAUGAAUAUGUAGGUACUUUGAAAAGUAUAAAAUGCAAUUGUUAGAAAGUAUUAUUAGUAUAUUAGUCUGAAAACAGCAUAAGCAGUAAGCCCCCCAGAUACCCCCACAUUUUUGUGUGUACAAUGGGGAUUGAACUUAGAAAAUUAAUUCUCCUGUUUUGGGAACCAUUGCCUCCCUUAUAGCCUGUUAAUAGGAUUUAUAAAACAUCAUUUCAGACAAAGUCAUUUAUCUUAUUUGCUAAUGAGACACAAAAUUUGGACUGUCUGGAACCAGGUAACAUUUUAAGAGUUGCCCAUUUGUUUCAUACACGUUCAGCUUUUCAGUGCAGUCAUUUUUAAUGGUGGUUUUUAUAGCAUCAAUAAAAAUAUUUUCAUAUAAUUCUUCCUUGUAAAUAUGGUUAAACUUUUAGCUUUCUACUACUUGGUGACCUGUUAAAUAACUUAAUGUACUUUGAAAUUGAUUGUUCAGUGCCAAGACAAUAAGAAGCCAGGAGGAGCCAGCUUUAUUUUUUACGUUGGGGCCUUAAGUUGGGCUAUGAAGAAAAAAUUCUGGCAGGGUUUGCCACAUCCAACUUUUAAGGGUUUUUUUAAUCUGUAAGAGGGAACAUGGACUAGAAUGCUUGUUUCUCUUUCCUGUCUGUCUUAAGUAGUAUCUUAGAUGGCAAGGAAAGGAAAUAUUCUACCCAUGUCAUAACAUAUCUACCAUUUAUUGAGCACCUACUAUGUGCCAAGUUGUAUUCUAAAUGCUUCAUGUAUUAUCUCAUCUGAUCCUUAAGGCAGACUCAUAGGUAGGUACUACUGUUAUCUCCUAUUUUAUAGGUGAAGAAAUUGAAGUCUAGAGAGGUUAAGAAUUUUCUCAAGGUAAGAUAGCUAGUAAAUGGUAGAGCUAGGGGUUUAACCUUGGCCAUCUGGCAACCAAGACAUAGGUUUGAACCCAUUAUGCCUCAUCAUACCUCAUAAUACCUAGUAUUAUAAGGGGUUUUGUUGUUUUUUCUUUGUAUUGGUUUUGUCAUCUGAAUCAAACGUCUUUGACCUAGAAAGAAUCUUAAAAUAUGCUUCUGCCGCCUCCCUCUUUUAUCCCAAUUCAGAAAACCAUUUUUUGGGAGACCUAGGUGCCAUAAAAAUGAAAAGAAAUGAGGCAUGGUGCUCAUGGUACUCACAGUUCAGUUAGUGAGGGGGGUUGGUAAGUAAAGGGGUAUGGCUAAGUAGCCCGCCAAGGAGGAUGACAUGUGCACUAAGCUGAUACUUGGCUGAUGUGCUCUGAGAGGCCAGAGCAGGCAGCAGUCAAGGUCAAGCAAAGCUUCAUUUGACCUGGGCGUGAAAGAAUGUGCAGGACUGUGGUAAGCAAAGGAGACAGGUGGCAUUUCAAGCUUCAGGAAUAGAAUGAACAGGGAGUUGGAGGAAAGAAAACACAAAAUGGCCUGUUACAAUAGUUAAGGCAAGAGAUGGGGAAACCUUCAACCUGGUCACCAGCAGACGACAUAAAGCAGGAAAUAAAAUGACAUUGCAAAGGCAAGGUGAUGGGAUUUGGCAAUUGAUUAGCAGUUGGGAGGGAGAGCACUGGAGGCAGGUACUGGGGUCUCGAACCCAGUAGGAUAGUAGGAAUGUUAAUCAUAAAAGGCAACUCCGAUUUGGGAACACUCAUUGUAGUUGGGGAGGUAGAAUAGGGUAGACGGCAAGAACUUGGACUCUAUAUUCAGAUGGUCCUGGGUGGCAAUCUGUGCUCUCCCACUUACUGGUAGAGUUACUUUCAGCAAGUCACUUGUUUAGACUCUAGUCUCCUCAUCUAUAAGGCGGGAAUAAUAUUAACACAGCUGACACUUGAGCAACACAGGUUUACACUGUGCAGGUCCACUUAUACGUGGAUCUUUCAAAAUAAAAGCUGCACCAAGUAUGCCUGCCUCUCCUGCCUCCCCUUCCACCUCUUCUGCCUCUGCCACCUCCAAGACAGCAAGACCCACCCCUCCACUCCCUCCUCCUCCUCCUCCUCCUCUUCAGCCUACUCAAAGUGGAGACAAUGAGGAUGAAGACCUUUAAGAUGAUCCACUUCCACUUAAUGAAUAGUAAAUACAUUUUCUCUUCUUCGUGAUUUUCUUAACAUUUUCUUUUCUCUAGCUUACUUUAUUGUAAGAAUACAGUAUAGAAUGUGUGUGUACAUAUAAAAAAUAUAUGCUAAUUGACUGUUUAUGUGAAUCAGUAAGGCUGCCGGUCAACAGCAAGCUAUUAAUAGUUAAAUUUGGGAGGAGUCAAAAUUUAUACAUAAAUUUUAGCCUGCAGGGGGUCGAGUGCCCCAAUCCCUACACUGUUCAAAGGUCACGUAUAGUGACCUCAUAGUGUUAUUGGAGCUCAGGUAGUACCUGUAGCAUGCAUAGCACAGUGCCUUAUAGCAUACAUUCAAUAAAUACCACUUAGUAGCCUCUUGGCUACUACUCACUCAUUUGGGUGAGUAGGAUUUUAUCCCCAUUUUAUAGAUGAGGAUGCUAAAAUUUGAGUAGGUAGAGUAGCUUUCCAGAGUCCUAAAGCCAGUAAAGCCUGGCAGGGGUGAGUAGAGACCCAGGCUCCUGCCUUGUGGUGUAGUUUCUGACUUCAAUUGUAGGUCACUUGCUGCCCUCACACCAGACAGCGGCAGGCCAAGUCUUCUGGUGCUGUUACUUUGACCUUCCUCCCAUAAAGGCUGGAUGUAGCAGAGGCAGGCACUGUCUCUUCUCUUACCUUCUGUGGCCAUUUACUGAGCAUGUAUGGUGUGUCUCACAUGCUUUUACAUGCUUUGCAUACAUUUCUUUUUCCUUUUCUUUUUAUUUUAUUUUAUUUUAUUUUAUUUUUGAGACAGAGUCUUGCUUUGUUGCCCAGGCUGGAGUGCAGUUGUAUGAUCUCGGCUCAUUGCAACAUCCACCUCCAGGGUUCAAGCAAUUCUCCUGCCUCCGCCUCCAAAGUAGCUGACAUUUCAGGUGCCCGCCACCACGCCUGGCUAAUUUAUGUAUUUUUAGUAGAGACAGGGUUUCACCAUGUUGGCCAGGCUGGUCCCGAACUCCGGACCUCAUGUGAUCCACCCGCCUCGGCCUCCCAAAGUGCUGGGAUUACAGUGCUUUGCAUACAUUUCUAAUGACUGAGUAUAGGUUUUCAUUUUCUCCCUUUGCUUUCUUCCUAUAAAUCAGACAGUCAUUUUUUUCUAGAGUCCUUUUCAGCACCCCAGAGGGAGUUGUAUCCUUUUGUGUGUGCCCUGUGGAAUUUUCAUGGCAACAUAAGUUGUAUUUCUUCAUGACUCACUGCCAUAGGAAGACCACCCAAAACAUACCCUCUUCUGUAACCCAAAUCUCAGCGUGUGUCCUUAUUUUCCUUGUUUUCAGCAUGUCCAAGUGAAGCCAUUAAGUAGGUAAUAUACUGUUAGACACAGAUCGUGGUGCUUGGGAAAACAACACCCAAGCCUCGUGAUUAAUAAGCACUGUUAAUUGUUAAGCUGCUCUUGCUGGUGUCUGACCUCACGGGGUUUGUGCUGUGACAGCUCUUUCAUGUUGAUGAGGUAAAUGAGUCUCUGCCAUGAUGGCCGGGAGAAGCCAGGACAGAGUAUCAGAUCGUGUUUCACCAGGAAAACAAGGUUGAUUUACUGUGUUACACGAGGGUGAAGUGGACCCAGCACCACUGCACCCCGUGCUUUGAUUCCCUUGUAUGCUAAAUAUGCAAGCACAAAACAGCUUUAACACAAUUUUUUACCUAGAAAGGAGCCUGGGGCUGCAUCCAAGUACAUUUAACAUGUGAAAAUUGAGCUGCUUUGAACUUGUAUGUUUUUGAUAACUGCUUGGUAUGCUUCCUGGAGGAUCACCUGUAGGCUUUUCUUUCCAAAUCCUAAUCCCUUUGAUUGAGUGCCAGGACAGAUAGCUCUCAUUGAAUAACUCCAGUCUCAUAAUUCUUCCUUCAUUCAGAGUUGAAAGGGAACAGCUCCAGAUUCAAUAGGCACAUCCUCAGAUUUAGCUGAAGUCAUUCAAACACUUUAAAACUGAAAUUGUUUUGUUCUGAAGUAGGGUUCAGUUGGGCUACUGAAUGUUUACACAAGCCAGUUGCUGCCAGGAACUGUAGGAUGGGGAAGAAAACCACACUUCUCCCCGCCUCCACCCAGCCCCCUUGCCUUGCUUCUCUCUGCCUCUGUAACCAAGAAGGAUUACAAGGACGACUUUGAGCGUUAGAAGUUUCAAAGCAACCUGGCAGGAUUGUUUGUAAACGUGGGCAUAAGAACGUGCUUGACUCUUCUUGUUUUCUGUCCUCCAUGAGACCAGGCUGAACACUCCUCCCCUCUCCUCCCAACCCCCUUUUGGAGGAAGGAAAACAACCAUGUUCUUUUUAUCUUUACAAAUGUGCCUGGUGGGGACUAAUCUAAACCAGUUCAAGAUGCUUUUGCUUAAGCCUGUUUAGAGGAACGGAAGGUGCUGCAGAAAUGGAAAUAGAGUGGUAUAUGGGCCUCUUUGCCACCCCGCUCCUGAGCUCGCUGCCUCUUUUUUGUUUUUGUGGGUUUCUUGGCACCUACCUAGAUUUCUGCUGAGAUCUCUGUUUCAGGUCUUUUCAGAGAUCAUGUUUCCUAAAAGAUGGUUCCUUUCUGCUGGACAUCCUGUCUCUGUCCUAUUUGGCCAGAUAGUACUUCAGUUGGGAAAAGCCAUCUUUCUCUUCGUGCCUGGUGCCCUAUUUCAGAAGGAAGCCUGAAAAGUCAUUUCCAUAUUCUGUGUGUGAUUGCGUCCUGCCUAGCUUAUCACAGUGGUUGUUCCCUCUCGGAUGAACAAUUCCUACCCUCCUCUUUGCCCAGCAGAUGAAGGCAAGGAUUGUAACCCAUUAUUAGAGUAUUGAGGACCUGAGUUCCCCACUCAUGUUGAACUUGAGGCAAGACUGGGCGGUUUAUUCCCCUCUGGCUACUCUCCCACUUGUAAAAUGAGGCGACAUCUCUAAUCAUUGACACCAAACAAGAACAUAGCCUAAUAAUAAAAUGAAUGGUGUUAUAUGGUCAUGAAGAAGGUUCAAGACUGGAAUCUACUCCAUAAGGAAGGACACAAAAAGAUUCAACAGUGAUUUAGACAAAUCUCAUCUGAACACAUUUUACAGAUGCCUGUUGAACUAAAAGUUCUGUCUAGGACUGUAGUAAGAUUUGACCCGGCUUAGCCUGGGAAUUUUGACCCACUGAUGGUAGAAGUUUAUUAACAGCCCUAUUCAUUUAGAUCCUUCCCUGUUUCUACUUUUCUCGUUCUCUCCCCGGAGGGUUUUUAUGACGUUGUAAUCAUUUAUAAUUUUAAAAUGUCUUCAAUCGUGCUUAAAAACAGCACUUGAUUUUAAUGGGUACUGCUUAACCAUAGAAAGAUUGUGUCUGUAUUACUGUCGGUUCUUACAACAAUACUUUGGAACGAAAGUAGAAAGUUUAUGACACAUUUUAUUAUAUUCCUAAAUGUGAAAGAGGAUUCUAAUUUAAAAAUAAGUGGCCAUACUUUUUAAUUCUUAUUUAGCCUCUGUAGCUGUUUUAAUAUCCCUUUUAUGGUUGACUGGUCGAUGUUUUAAAACAAGUUCUUCAGGGACUCUGCCCAUUAGUCUUUGGCAAUAAAAUCUGAACUUUACUAAAAUAAAACAUGAAGCCAUGGAGUAAUUAAGAGGGGAACUUUCAGAGAUGACCGUGAAUAUGAAAUACAGUGAUUUGUAUUAUUAAUGGAUUUGGGGAAAACCAGCCCACCUCUUUUAAGCUCAACUAUGUGUAUUUGGGGGGUUUUAUAUUUUUAAUUUAUUUCUUUGUUUCUCUCAAGGCAGUAGGGGUUCCAUCGCAAGCUCUUAAGAUCUACCAAUCCUCCUUUUGUAGCCUGCUGCUUCUGAAUAUGAGCCUUUCUUUUUUCAUUUUAUUUGGAAAAUGGGGUGAUGUCACUUAGGAAAGCAUUUUUCCCAAAAGUGGUUUCAGGAACCAGAAUCUGGUGAAGUGUUAUUUAAAAGCGAUAACAUAGUAAAGCUCUGCUUUGUGCUUCAAAUAAUUGUAGGAUUUACGGGAUAUAUCCCUAACCUGUUCAGUUUUAUGGAAGGACAAAAUACAGGGAUUCAUUUUAUCAUAGUUUCUUAAAAACUUUGAAACCCAGUUGACAGUCAUUUCUCUAGCAUUAUAAUAAGCUCUUUGUGUUUAUAAACCUAGUUCAUAGUAAUUUUUGGAGUGCUGCAAUUUGGUAGUUAUUUAAUUUGCAAAUGGGAUUGGCCUCUCUAACCUCUAAAGGAACUAGUUCCUUUUAAUGCUUUAAAACUUUCAUUGACUCUCAAUUGCCAACUGCAGGAAAAAGUUCAGGUUUUAAAAGUCCUUACAUGCGUUUCAGCCUCCUCUCCCUGUUUCCUUUAUGAACAGCCCCCUCCCACUCCCUUUCUUUCAAUGGUAGGUCUGCUGCAGAACAUUCUGCAUCUCUUAAACUUUAUAUGCACUGUAUUUUUCAGUCUCCAUUCCUCUGCUCAUAUUGUGUUCUCUCCAUGGAUUCUUUCUUUUUAUUAUUUAAUUUUUUUUAAGGGAUAGGGUCUCACUCUGUUGCCCCAGGCUGGAGUACAGUGGCACCAUCAUAGCUCGCUCGUAGCUCACUGUGGCCUCCAACUCCUGAGCUCUAGUGAUCCUCCCACCUCAGCCUCCUAAGUAGCUGGGAUACAGGAACGCACCACCAUGACAGGCCAAUUUUUAAAUUAUUUUUUGUAGAGACAGGGUUUCACUGUAUUGCCCAGGCUGGUCUCAAAUUCCUAGCCUCAGGCAAUCCUUCUGCCUCAGCCUCCCAAAGCGCUGGGAUGACAGGUGUGAGCCACCAGGCCUGGCCUCAGGGAUUUCUUCUUUACCAUGUCAUAGUCUCCAAAAUUGUGCCCUUCCUUUCUGUCAACUCAAGUGUUUCCUCCUUUUUUUUUUUCUGAGACAAGGUCUCGCUCUGUUGUCCGGACUGCAGUACAGUGGUGCAAUCUCUGCUCACAGCAAUUUCCGUCUCCCAGGUUCAAACAAUUCUCGUGCCUCAGCCUCCCGAGUAGCUGGGUUUACAGGUGGACACUACCACUCCCAGCUAAUUUUUGUAUUUUUUGGUAGAGACGGGUUUCACCAUGUUGGCCAGGCUGGUCUCAAACUCCUGACCUCAAGUGAUCCGCCCGUCUCGGCCUCCUCUUAAGAGGUAUUUUUUACUCUGUAUCCAGAGCUUCCUCAUAUACCCAUGCAGCAUGUGGAAAACAGCCUGUACUGCUGUAUGCAGUGGCCCUGUUGGAAUCCUUCUGCUUCCCAGCGAAUUGCCCACACCCCAGACCAUGGCACUGUCUCCAGAUCUUCAGCAUUGCAGUUAUCAUGUUAAACUUAGCUAUUUGUGUAUAUGAUUGUCUCGUUCACCAAACAGUGAGCCCGUUGAGGGCGAAGUUGUCUUAAAUGGCUUUGUGUCCCCAACUGCCACCAGGGAGAUGCAUAGUAACUAGCCAAUGAAUGAAUGUUUUCUUCCCUUAAAAAAUACCAACAGAUGCCUAACAUAAGCAAUUAAGUGAGGGAAAGCUUUUUUGCCAUUUUAAAAGUCAUUCGUCAGCCCACACGAUACCACUGAGGAAGCCUCAUGUGAGAGCUAAUGAACAUUAAACCCAGACACCAUCGGGAGCUCACCAGAAACCCAUGGCUGGCUAGUGAGAGACCCGGGGCUAGAAACUUGAUAUUUUGGUUUCACAGCCAGGUACCCUGGCAGCCACACCAGUGUUAUGCUGGCAGGCAUGCUUUGUCUGCUAUCUGUGGCGUGAACUUUACUAAAAUGAAACAUGAUGCCAUGGAGCAAAUUAAGAGGAAAGCUUUCAGAGAUGACCAUGUAUAUGAAACACAGUUCCUACUCCGCCUCCUUCACCCCAAUGAGAGAAUCCAAAUUUUAUUUAACUGGUGCAUAGAGGUCUCUUGAUUUGGGGGAAGAUGGGUCCCUCUGCCAGCCUGAGAUGGUAAAUCACGCUUGGGUUAAGCCAGUCAUCGAAUUCCUGUUCCCCUUUGCUGGAUGCUCAUUUUCCCGGGUUCCCUUGCAAGUCAGGGGCUGUGUGACAAGUUCUGACCUGUGAGACACAAGGCCAAGUCCACUAGGAGAAUUCUGGGAAGGAUUUUCUUCCUGGUAAAAAGACAGAGCCUCAUGUUUGCCAAAAGAGCCUGAUUCUCUGCCCUUUCAGAGGCUUCCUGCCUUUGCACACAGUGACAAGACAUGAUGCUGGGGCUUUAGCAGCCACCACGAGGUGACAGGUAGGAGGACAAAAGUGAUUACAUUGAUGUUGGUGAAGCAGGAUAGAAAGAGCCUGGGUCCACAAUGACCAACCUUGAAACCUCCCAUUUCCAGACUUCUGGUUCAAUAAGAAGCACCCCGAUGGUUUCAUCUUUUGACGGUUGGUUUUUUGCUGCUUGAAACAGGACACAUCCUAACUGAUUCAGUUACUUUUAGAAGGAAAAAUAAAAGUGGAGACAGCAUCCUAAGAGGAAAGGUGGUGACUGGAUAAACUAUAUGGAAGUCCUGACAACAUCAUAUUUAAGAAAUUUGGUGGCUGGCCUCUAUUCUUCUGUUAGGUGUAAGGAAGACCCACUGAGUAACACUGGAGCAUUCAUCAUUCAAGAAACAUUAUAUUUUAAUCUUGGAUAUUCCUAGCACUAUGCAGGAUUCUGAGGAUGCAGAAAUAAAAGGCAGUUUCUAUCCUUAAGGAACUUGGAGCCUAGUAAGGGAGACUAGUGAGUAAACAAUUACCUGAGAGUAUGAGGAUCACUCUCUUUUGAUAGGGGUAUUGUAUUAGCUCUUAUGCUGCUGAUAUGCCUGAGACUGGGUAAUUUAUAAAGGAAAGAGGUUUAAUUGACUCACAGUUCCACAGGGCUGAGGAGGCCUCAGGAAACUGACAGUCAUGGCAGAAGGAGAAGCAAACACAUCCUUCUUCACAUGGUGGCAGCAAGGAGAAGUGUCGAGCAAAAGGGGGAAAAGCCCCUUAUAAAACCAUUGGAUCUCAGGCCGGGCACGGGGGCUCACACCUGUAAUCCCAGCACUUUGGGAGGCCGAGGCAGGCAGAUCACCUGAGGUCAGGAGUUCAAGACCAGCCUGGCCAACAUGGUGAAACCCCGUCUGUACUAAAAAUACAAAAAAAAUUUAGCCUGGCGUGGUGGCGGGUGCCUGUAAUCUCAGCUGUUCAGAAGGCUGAGGCAAGAGAAUCACUUGAACCCAGGAGACAGAGGUUGCAGUGAGCCGAGAUUGUGCCAUUGCACUCCAGGCAAUGGAGUGGAGCAAGACUCUAUCUAAAGAAAAAAAAGAAAGAAAGAAGGAAAGAAAGAGAGAGAGAGAGAGAGAGAAAAGAGAGAGGGAGAGAAAGAAGGAAGGAAGGAGAAAGAAAGAAGGAAGGAAGGAGAGAGAGAGAAAGAAAGAAAGAAAGAGAAACCAUCAGAUCUCGUGAGAACUCAAUCACUAUCAGCAUGGGGGUAACCGCCCCCAUGAUUCAAUUAUCUACCACUGAGUCCCUCCCACAACACAUGGGGAUUUGGGGAACUACAAUUCAAGAUGAGAUUUGGGUGGGGACACAGCCAAACCGUAUCAGGUGUGUUUGGGGUACUAUCGGAGAUCAGAUCAGGACCACAAAACCUGGAUAGGCUGGGGAACAGGAGAAAUCAGGAAAUGUUUCCUGGCAGAAAUAAUGGCUAAGUCAAAUCUUGAAGAAGGGAUAGGAUUUUGCCAGACCAAGAAAGACAAGGAAAGAAGGGGCGGGGCGGGGUGGGAGUGGGGGGGUGGUGCAGUAUACAAAACAGAGGGGACGUGUUAUAAGGCAGAGAGGUAUGAGAGAAAUAGAACAUUCAGAAACUGUCCUUCUUAAUAUUUUUGCCAUAUUUGAUUUGGAUCUUUUUUUUUUUAGGAAAAAGCUGCUGAUGGCUACAAAUGUGUCUGUUAUGUUAUUCUCUAUACUUGUUAUUUCAAAAAUAUUUUAUAAAAAUUUGUGAGUGAAUAAAUGAGAGGGGAGAAAGGAAGGCAAUGAGUAUGAAUCAUCAUUCUGAUUUUAAGCAUAAUAAAAGCAGGAGGUGACUUCCACAGUCAAAUACAUUUGGGAAAUAAUAGAAAAUUAAAUAGUGUUCAUUAUUGUGAGAAUUCCCAGAACCCUUAAUAUUCCCAUGUUGAUUGUUACUGUCCAAGAUGGGGCCACUGUCUAGCGCACUUCCUAGGAUAGAUUUGUCCAUAGGCCCCUCUUUUAUGUAACCAUCUGCCGAACUGAGGCCUUGGAAAGGCUUGAUGUAGACCGCUCUUUCAGAAAACUUGACCGAGAAGGGAAGUACGCUUCUAGGGUAGCAUCAGAGCAGAACAUGGGGAAAGGGAGACAUUUCACAAGAAGGGAGAGUCAAGAUCAUGUGUAUUUAUUUGCCAAGGGCAAAAAGCAGUAGUGAGGAAAAGCAAACAAAAACCAGUUGAAGACACAGCAACAGAGGAGAAUGAUUGACAAAGUAAGCAAGGUGCUUGAGGUUACAAAAGGGAUCAGCUAUUAAAGGACUUCUGCUAGUGUCUACUUGUCAUCUUCAAGAUGGCACAAUUUUUACAGUACCAUGUAUCUGUGUUGCAGGAGAAGGUAGGCCUCUCAAUCAGAGACUUAGCCUAUAAACCAGCAUCUACAUAGUGAAUCUAGGUAUCCCUCAGUGUUCUUCUAUUUAUAAGGAACAGAAAACCCAACUUAAAUUGACUUACGUAAAAAGAGUUUGUUGGUUGGUGUAAUUGAAAAGUACAUGGUUAACUAGCUUCAGGCAUAGCUUGAUCCAGGUAUUAACUAUGUCACCAAGAUCCAUCUCACUGCUCAUAAGCCCUCUCAGUUGGCUCUAUUCUUAUGUUCCUCAUGGCUCCUGGAAACUUUAGCCUCUUUCCUUCUGGUUGCAGGAUGGUUGUAGCUCCAUAGACAUCACAUCUGCCCUCACACUGCAACUCCUAUGAAGAGGAAACACCUUAUUUCUCAGGAGCCCCACCCUCUUACUAUUAGUCUGAUUGAAUUAUAUGUCCAUCCUUGAACCAAUUCUUAUGACCAGGAAUAAGGCAUAGUCCCCAUGUAUGUAACUUCUUUCUCCUGAGUUGUACAAAUUAUCAAAGGAAAACCAAGAGGAUUAUAUCUCAAGAGUGGAUUAUGUUAAGAAAGUAACCCUUUCCCUCCAAAAAAGGAAACUUCCAUAACAGAACCCUUAGAUUUUUACCCAGUGUGAUUUUAAACUCUAAAUGCUGGAAUGUUUAGGGUCCCAGGUCUGACAGCAUGAAUUAGAUCCCUCCAUGUGGAGCACCCAAGUAAGUGAAGGGUGUUGACAGCCAUCAUGGGGAAUGCUGAUGCUUACUGAAGAAGCCAUGCAAUAAAUCCUCUUUAGAAAUAAACAAAAAGCAGCUUUUGAGAACCCGGCUUUUACCCAAGACCAAAACCUGUCAGCCACAGGCAGAAGUCAUUAGGCAGGAUUUAUAUGUGCUGGUAUCCAACACUGAGUCAAAAGGAGAUCCGUAGAGGGGAUUUCUCUCUUCCGGAAACCCAGCAGAGGAACGGGGAAGACUUUCCGGGUAAAGUUUCAGAGAACCUAAUGCAUAAAUCCCCUUAACAAACACUGGGAUUUGGGUUUGUAACUCAUCUCUCCCAGCUUAGGUCCUGUGGAGACAAGCUGUCAUAGGGCUGACACAACCAAAUCAAGAAAGGAAAGAGUAGAAUUUAUAGUGAAAAUCAGGAAGCUACUUAAAAUGGUGGGUUUCUCAGAAUGUGGUACUGCACAUUUUUUGCUUGGUAGUCCCUGAACAGUUAUUAAAGACCCCAUGGAAGCAGAUGGAUGCUGGCCAGUAGGCAUUGUCCCCUUUUAUAUUUAUAACUUCACUGACCUUCAUUUUACCUCUAAUAGAGAUUGUACCAUUAAUUGGCUGGAUUCUCCCAAGCUCUGUGGCAAGUAAGAAUGGAAAAGUGGAUUUUCUCCGUACUCCAUUGCAGAGGAUAUCAUUAAUUUGCUAGGUUUCGUUCCCACAGGGAAAUGUUAAAAACCAGUACAGUUGGUUCUUCGCCACUCUGGAUUGACAGACAUUCUUUGUGUAGGUGCCUCUGGCUUUGAGAAACGAGGCCAGAGUCUAUAUGCAGACAGUGAGCAGUGAUCUUCCGUUUCCUACUUGUUGCAGUAGACAUAAAAUCAGGGCAAAUGGUGAGUUCCAGAGGAAAGGAUCCAGCAUGCAGCCUGCUGAAUAAGAGAACAGGAAUGAUCUCGAAUGAUGAUAAAUGUUUAUACUCUAUUAGAGCUUUGGCCAUGGGUUUGGCCACCAUUCAAUUGCCUCUACAGCUGAUUUUUUAUGUGGCUUUUCUUUUCUUUCUCCUGUUUGGUUGCAAACUUAUUUUGACUGAGGAUUUACUUGUCACCUCAUGUUGACAUUUCAAGUUAUUGCAUUGAGAAAAACAUAGGAGAAAGCAAACAAGCAAGUAUAUUCCAACGGUCAACAGGCACAGAAGUCAUACUCACAUUUCAAAGAAAAACAGGAGAGUUGAAAUAGAGAAUGGAGAACAGAUGUAUUUAUGAGGGGGGAAAUCUUCUUGGCAUUUGAGCUCAAGUCAGAUUCUGGAUUCUGGAUAGUUUUCUCAGCUAAUGGUGAUUCCUAGGACUGCUAAGCGGGGGACAUUCUGGUCUAACCGAAGUUGCCAUGUAAUUCUGUGGAAUCAUACUAACAUUUUGAUUUCUCUGAUUAUAAGUGACUGCAGCAACAAAGAGAGUAACUCUGUUGUAAGAACUGUUUCCACAGUGUCUCUAGGGACAGUUUUGCUUUAGUCUGUAAAUUCUCCAAAGGCAAGCUGAGACUAUGUAAAUUAAAGAAAUAGAGCCAGUGACAACCAACCCUGUGGUUUUAUUUGAUUUUCCAAAACACAUGUCCAUCGGUAUGUCUCAGACAACACGAUAUGAUUAAAGCACGGUAAUAAUCACCCAUAUAUUGCAUUUUAAUUGGUAUAAUGUAUGAUGAAUAGUGAAGUUGGAACCAUGGGGCAUACUUUCACAUUUAAGGUAUUUCUUUGAUUUAUCAGAAUUUCUAAGAACAUAAAAUAGAAGUCAGAAAGUCUGUUUUCUGAGCUGGGACCUGCCAUUCAUCAGCUGUGUGAUCUUGGGUAUGUUACUUUAUUUCUCUGGGCCCCAUUUUCCCCAGCUAUAAAAUGAGGGGUUUAAACUAGAUGAGCUCUAAAGAGCUUUUCACUUCGGAGUUUGGCUAUUCCAAGACCUUUUCUAGUCUUGUGAAUUUAAUUACUGAAUUCUGGGAUCUUAAGUCUCUUUAUCAGUUGAGUCUCCUCCUUUGUGGUCUUACAGCAAAGAUGACUGUUGGCCAAACUUUGGAUUUCUGAGACUGAUUUCAGUGAAUUGCAUUAUACAUAUUUUUAACUAGCUUAUAUUAAAUGAGAGAAAGUGCAAGGAAGGAAUUGCAACCACAAUUUAAAUAGUUUUUUCCGUGCCAUUCUAUUCCGUGAGCACCUGCCUUGGAGUAGGUGUGAAACGGGAGUCAGGAAGUCUGUGCAUGCCUCUCAGAGGGUGGUAUCUUCGUCUUCUGAGUAUGAUUCCGUACCAUGAAUAUGUUGGUUGUGGAUUUUUCUUUUCUGUACAACAUGAGGCCCCUAAACAUAAGGAAACUACUUCCUUUGGUGCUUAACCUAAGAAGCAUCUAUUCUAAUGAUGGAGGAAAACCUAGCUGUAUUACACAUACUGAAAGUGAUAUAGUGGGUUACAAAGUGACAGGUAAAUAUUUGUGUUCCAUUUAAGUGGUUUGUGAGUAUAAUUUUGAUUUUUCCUAACUGUUGCUUUCUCUAAUGAUUUUAGAACCGGAUAACCCCUCCCCUUUCCCCUACUCUCCAAGCAUAGGAUAGAGCUCAUCUAUAAAAUUCAUUGGAUUUUGUGUUUUUGCUCUUCUAGUUGGUCUCUGAAAUGGUCAGAAUGGAGUUGGAAAUGGGACAGCCUAUUAGUCCAAUCUACUUCUAAGGCUCCUGAACAGCCUCACAAGACUCCAUGCAUCCCAGCAUCCCUUGGGACCUGGGUGAUUAGUUUGUGAUCAACAGAUUGUACUCUCAGAAAACGUGCAAGCCACCAGCCUCUCGUUCAAACUGUUUAUAGGCCCCAGAAGGGGCUUCCUUUGGGCCAGAUGAUUAGUCACAUUUUGUUUCAAACACCCGAGGAAAGGUACAGCAGCUUUCUACUUGAAUGCAUGCUUUUACCACCUAAAGGCAAUUGGUUGGGAGAAGAUUUGGGAGAAGACAUUGACAGUGUCCAGCAGUCCUUUUAUCUGUUAUAAAGCUAAAUGCAUGUUUAUCAAGUUUUCAGCAAAGAUAUAUGUUCCACUUUAGCCUCCUUAUUCUUAUUUUCCACUUAGAGGUAGAGACUGGGUCUCACCAUGUUGCCCAGGCUGGUCUUCAACUCCUGGGCUCAGGCUCAAGUGAUCCUCCGACCUCGGCCUCCUGAAGUGCUGGGAUUACAGGCAUGAGCCACUGUGUCUGGCCACAAUACACACUUGACUGUCAUUUAUAAACUCAAAUGACUCAGCUAUCAAGAUGCCAAAUUGGAUUUUAGAGAGCCUCCUCCUAGGCACCUGAUACUUUCAUGCUUGGCUUAUUGUACGAGGUAACUCCACUUUCUGUUCAUCUCAAAAGUGUUGGGAAGUGUUUGCAGGUUACCUUCCUAGCACCUGCCCAACCUUCUAGAGAAGUGGAGAAACCUGUGAGGAAAGCAGCACAGGCGUUGCCACUUAGGGACAGUUUCAUGGAAAGAGAUCUCUACUUCUUGAUGUCACAUUACCCUUUAGAAUUCCAGAAUCACUUCAGAUCUUCAAAGCUUUUAAUAAGCAGCGAUGGCCUUUUACAAUUAUUUUUUAAAGCAGCAAUACUUAAAAUUUUAUUAAGUGCUGUCGUAGAAACUUGUGUCUACAAAAGACAGAUAAAAACAAGUGUUGAUGAGGAUAGAGAAAAAUUGGAGCCCUCAUACAUUACUAGUGAGGAUGUAAAAUAGUGCAGCCACUCUGGAAAAUAGUGUAGAAGACCCUUUUUAAAAGUUAAAUAUAGAAUUACCCUAAAAAGCACAGGCUUUUGUUGACUUUCCCUGGGGGUCAGGUGGGCUCACCUUGGUGCAUCCUCCCCUGGGGGGCUCUGGUGUGGGAAGCCAGCUUUCCUACCAUUCUGCAUGCAGCCUUGUACUGGGUCCUUGGGGAAAGAGAAAGACUGUGAAAUAGAUGUUUCCCUUUUCCCAGAAAUACCAACCCAAGAUCCCCAGCAGUGACCCCUUAUGGAAUUCUGGGAAGAACUAAAGAGAUAACAGUAUUCUUUCCUGCCUUUUAUCAACUCUGGAUGGCAGGAGGGACUCUGGGGCUUGGGACUGGCUGCCCUCAGGAGUUCAUGGCCUAGUACUGAUGCCAAGGGGCAGAAAUUUGUGAGAAAGAAGGCCUCCUCCAGGAGCUGUUGGUAUGAGCCCCUAAUGGGAUCAUGAUAUCCUACAUAUGCAACUAUGGGAAGAAGAAAGGAUCUAGCCAACAUCUGUUAUUAUAUUUUAAAAAGUAAUUUAAUUUGUUUACAUUACUUGUCAUUAUUGUCACCCACUUAUAUUUGAUUAUUCUUUAAGCACAUAUAGAAAGAUGAGGUUUAUGUUGAUUUUUCUGGUAUUACAUUUCCCUAGGCUACAUCUCCAUAUAGAGCUUUCCUUUUUUAAAAUCUGUUCUUUAUUUUUUAUAGAGACAGGGUCUUGCUAUGUUGCCCAAGCCAGUCUCAAACUUCUGGCCUCAAGUGAUCCUCCAGCCUCAGCCUCCAAAAGCUCUGGAAUUACAGGCAAGAGCCACUGUGCCCAACCUCCCCAUAUAGAAUUUUCUAUAGCAAUCUUGUCCUAGGAAAUAUCAUAGAAAUAGUUUAGGUUUUAAAAAGAAGGGCUGUAUGUCAUCUAAACUCUUAUUUAACCUAUGGUUGACAGCCUUGCUAUUAAAAAAAGAUCUUAAGUUGUUUUACAUUUUAUAGUCUUUUUAAAAAAAGAUGAUGAGACAUCUCUUUAGUGGUUGCCAUGUUUAAUAUUGUUACUUUCUAAGAACAAAUAUAAUUUUUGUGAGAACAUUAUAUUACUCUGAAACAGAGAACAGUACUCUCUGUCCUUUUAGUCCCUCAAUUUUUGAUAAGGUAAAAUAAGAUUAUCUUAUAUGACUAGUGUAUACUACCUUAUAUUUGUAUGACACUCCAUGUUUUUCAAUGACUUUCUUCCAGAGUUUUUGUUGAAACACAAAAGGAUUUGUACCCAAACUGACUUUACUUUCAAUUCUGGAUAAUAGAUAAUUAUUAUUGCAUUACAACUUUUAAAAAUAAUUAAGAAAUCAGCUUAGAAAAUGCUUGAUGAUUUUUACUUAGCAUGGUACGUCUUUAGGGAAAAGACCGUAUUAUGAAUUUAGCAAGCAAGUUGAGCAUGGUGACAUCCGCCUGUAAUCCCAGCUACUUGAGAGGCGGAGGGGGGAGGAUCACUUGGGCCUGGGAGUUCCAGACUACAGUGAGUUAUGAAGGGACCCACUGCACUGCAGCCUGGGCAACAGAGCAAGACCCUGCAAAUAAAUAAAUAAAUAAAUAAAUAAAUAAAUGUCGUGGUUUUUUUUUAAUUUAGCAAGUAAAGUAGCAGAAUAUCCUAUGUUGGAUUAGUCAGUGGAAAAAAAUAUCUUUCAAAUCGCAUUUGAUGUUUGCUCACCAUUAUUAUGAACUAAGCUACUCCAUGGAACUAGAGCAUAGCUGUCAAGUAAUUAUGAAGCGCCCAUGCUAGGGACCGCAUGCCAUUUAAUGAGUUUACAUCAGUAAAAAGAGAGGACAGAUUCAAAAAUGGGACAUGUCACACAUACAUGUGAGAAUUUUCCCAUAGGCCAAAGGGCCUCUUUCUUGGUUUUGAUAUCAGGCACCAACUCUAAUAGGAUGAAGCUAUCUGUGUAGCUUGAUGAAGUAGAAAUUCAUUGGAGUGGCCGGGCACAGUGGCUCACACCUGUAAUCCCAGUACUUUGGGAGGCUGAGGCGAGCGGAUCAUGAGGUGAGGAGAUCAAGACCAUCCUGGCUAGUACAGUGAAACCCCAUCUCUACUAAAAAUACAAAAAAUUAGCCGGGCAUGGUGGCAGGUGCCUGUAGUCGCAGCUACUUGGGAGGCUGAGGCAGGAGAAUGGUGUGAACCUGGGAGGCAGAGCUCACAGUGAGCCGAGAUCGCGCCACGGCACUCCAGCCUGGGCCACAGAGCGAGGCUCCGUCUAAAAAAAAAAAAAAAAAAAAAGAAACAAAUUCAUUGGAGUACCUUAGCAUUAUGGGAUAUCUCUAGGCAGCGCCAGGUUUCUUGUCUUCAUAGCUAAGAUAGAUGUUAAAGGAAGGGGAACCUUUUUCUAUCCCAUUUUUCUAGUGGCCUUUAUAGGACUUGGCUUAAUAUUUUUAUUUUAUUUUAUAUUAUUAAAUUAAUAUAUUUUUAUUUUAUAAAAUAAAAAUAUUAAGCCAAGUCCUAUGAAGGCCAGCAGAUUUUAUUUUAUAUAUAUAAAUUUUUUAAAAUAUGAAAUAAAUAUAUAAUACAUAUAUAAAUAUAUUUUUAAAAUAUGUAAUAUACAUAUAUGUAUGUGUACACACAGUGUGUGUACACUUGUUAUAUUAUUACUUAUCCUAGUAUAUUAAUGGCUAUAUAACAUAGCUGUGUCCCAAAUACAUGUAAUACAUAUUACUUUUCAUCUCAUUUAAACCUCACGAGAGUUCUUUGGUGAAGAUAUGAUUACCAUUUUACAGAUGAGAAAACCUGAGAAGAAUAGAAGUUAAGUAGCAUGCCAAGCUUACCCAACUAGCUCUCAUUCAUUCAUUCAUGAUUCAUGAAGUAUUUAUCAAACAACUACUAUAUACUGUCAUUAAAGAUACAAAAAGGAUCAAACAUAAUCCUUGCCUUCAAAGAAGCCACAGUCUAAGGUUAACAAGUGGACUGGAGCGGAAUUUGGUUUUAUCAUUUCAAAGGCAAAGGAACCCAGAUUGGAGAGUUUUCUGGCAACUGCCUUAGGACUUUUUGGCCAAGAUUAAUGUAAUAUAUAAAGGUAAGCAUCAAUGUGUUGGUGGGAAGAAGUAUCCUAGAAAUGUUUUUUGUUUUUUACUGUAUCUAGGACUCUUAUGAACUACUAAUUCAUUAUUAAGUUAUUUGAUGACACAGAUUAUUGUUCAAGAAUUUCCUCCCAGAGCAAUUGAUAAAUAUCAAAUAAUUUUUAUGAUGAGCAGUUCCAGAAAGGGUUAAAGUUAGCUUCUCUGGGACAUAUGAUGGGAAAGUAGCUGAACAUGAUUUCAAAGGGAUUUUUUAGGAGAAAAUUCCAAUUAACAGAGAAGUAAUUUCCCUUUCUAGCUUACUAAGCCCUAUUUCAGACUAAUGCAGUUUCAAGAUCAUCUCCCUUCUCCCCUUAUUUCAACAGAUAUUUUGAAUAUGAAAAUCUUAUGUCAAAACUUAGCUGAAGCCUUCAUCAGGCUUUUGAAAGGCUAAGUAAGAAUUCUGUUUCUAGGAAUAAAAAGAUUUGGAUCAGAAAGAUUCUUUGCUGGCUAGAGUUCCUUUUCGGAUGGUAGUUCAAGCAGUCUUUAAUCAUAUUUUUGUUGAUUAUUUAUUAGUUUCCCUGGGAAAUCAAAGACUCAGUAACGUAAAAUGUGUUUUCCUUAAGAUAUUUUAUGAAUCAGAACCCACAGUAAAGAAAUAAUGGGAAAUACAUUUCCUUUGCUGAUAUGGACUAAUUGAGAAUUAAAAUCCCUUUCUCUAGUCAUUAUCCCACAUGGAAAUGCUGAAUGACCCAACUGGCCCAAUUGCACCAACCACAGUUUCUGCCUAGACAAAACUCUUAUGCCACUAGUAGAUAAAGAGAGAGCUUUCUCAGUAAAUCAAAACUGCAGAGAACUAGAACUAAUUUAAGUGAAAGGAUAGGCUCCAAGCCCGCUGUUUGGGUAAACCCACACUGAACCAAGUGAGCGAUUGAUGAAACUUAAUAUAUGUGUAUUCCAGUCAUCAGCCUGGAGUAUGUGUAAUGCAAGCCCAUGGUGUUUGUCACUGUGAGAAAUGGAAAGGCAGACCUUCAUUCUCAACUGUGUGGGGCUGCUAGCCUGUGGCAGCUUUGGUCAACAUCGGGCUUGCUUUUGGGUGAGCCAGACUUUGGCUGGUUUCCUGAUGGAGGUUAGGGGAAUUGUGAAAUGUGUCUCCUUACACAGAUCGUCCUGAUCAAAUGAAAUAAAAAGGUAUUUUAAAAAUAAUUUGCUUAGUGAAAUACAAAGGAAAUAGGAUGCAUUUCAUACUAUUAAGGCCGAUAUGGUUUUGGGGGAUACGAGGUGUACAUACGUGAAAAAUUUGAAAACAAUUCAGAGUGAAAAAGAAUGGUCGUAUAACCUAAUGUAAAUGACGAGUUAAUGGGUGCGGCACACCAGCAUGGCACAUGUAUACAUAUGUAACAAACCUGCACAUUGUGUACAUGUACCCUAAAACUUAAAGUAUAAUUUAAAAAAUAAAAGAAAAAACAAAAAAGAAUGGUCGUGUAGUAGAGACAGUGGUGAAGAGCAGGACUCUGGAGCCAGGUGUUCUGAGUUCAGAGCCCACUCUGCCACUUACUAGAUCUGAGACCUGGAGGAAGUUAUUUGCCCUUUCCCUGUUUGGCUCUUUUGUAAAAUGGAAAUAUAAGAGUACCCACCUCCUAAGGUGGGCUUAUGAAUUAAUAGAUAUAAAGGUAUGUAAAAUUAUUGCUAUCAUUAGUUACUGUUAUUAAUAGAUCAGAAGUCACAAGCUCCAAUGCCUGCAGUGCCCAUGCAUACCAAAACAGGGAUCACUGGCAACAGAGACAUGGCCCCAGUGGCGUGGAGAUAAAAGAAAGUGGUAGGGACAGUGGCAGACAGCCAUCACCCUACUCCCCAUUGAUUGUGACCCUAAGGGAAUGCUGGUCCUGUGUCGCCAGAGCUUCUGGUAUUGCCAAAGAAGCUUGAAAUCUGGACUUGGUCAAAAAAUCUCUCAACUUGUAAAGGUGGUUGCUUUAUUUUAAAUUACUCUACAAGCCAAAUAAAACACUGUCUCCAGGCUAUUGGCCACCAGUGAAUGACCUCUUUGGACUAACAAUUAAACUCAGCUAUGGAAAUUCAUCUGAUUACUUUAUUGUCACACUGUGAAACAGGGAUUCAUUGUCAUUCCAGAAACAGCCAUUGAGUCCCUGCUUGUGUCCACCCCUGUGCUGGUGCAAAGGAUGUGCCCAAGAAUCAGGCAGACAAUCCAAAGAAGCCACCUGCUCCUUUACAAGUUGUUGACAAUUAAGAAACACCUAGCACUUAAUAGAUUCUCCAUAAAUGUAGGUUCCAACUCCUUCCAUUACCUUUGAUACGUCUAGACCUGAUCCAGUGAGUAUUUGAGGGCCAAUCUCAGUUUCUAAGUAGGAAUAGUGAUAUUGUUGAAAACUAAUGAACCCACCGACAACAUCACAGAAAUACUCCUAUACUUCUUCAAUGUGAGUUUCCUGCUUUUUGUGUCAUUUAUCAUCCCCUUUUAUUUGAUGUCUCUACUCAGGACUUAGGACUCGGGCUGUGAUAUUGUGUAUGUUACCUCACAAUUUUUUUUCUGUUUUUUUUUUCUUUAAGUGUAUAAGCUUCGUUUAUACUUCCAAAGGAUCUUCAAUGGAACUCUACUUCUGUGAGCUAAACCAGUGUCAUACUGCAAUGAAAACUGCAGGUGAUAAACAUUGUCUAAAUAAAAUUUCCAAAAAGUAUUUGACCAAGAAAUACCUUCCCCCUGCAUUCCCCACUUAAUGCAUCUUAAUAUGCCAAGUUACUGAUAUUGUUUGACCUAUUUGGGGAAAUGCUGGCUUGCCAAAUUAUUGCCCUUGUUAGGAACUACAGUUUCUUGUAAUUUCUUACCCACUCCGGCAUCCACACAGGUAUCUUCCAAAGCUCAGACUUUAUUUUCAAGAGGUCUAUCUGAGACCAGUCUGGGUAACCAAGUGAGACCCUGUCUCCACAAAUAAUAAUAAUAAUAAUAAUAAUAAUAAUAAUAAUAAUAAUAAUAAUAAUAAUAAAUUAGCUGGAUGUGGUGGCAUGUGCCUGUAGUCCCAGCUACUUGGGAGGCUGAGGUAGGAGGUUUGUUUGGUCUCAGGAGUUCGAGGUUGCAGUGAGCUAUGAUCAUGCCUUUGCACUCCAGCCUGAGUGACAGAAAAAGACCCUGUCCCCCCCCCAAAAAAAAAGUCUAGCAACUUGAGUGUGGCAGUGGCCAACUUGAUGGUAACUAACAAUGGGAUUGCAAACUCUUUGAGGAAAGGAACUGUCAUCCUGAACUCGGCAUAGCACCAAGCACUGGGUUGUUACAUGGUGGGUGUUAAGCAAAUGCCAUGGAAUGCAACAGACCCCUUUUUCUGCUGCUGUAAACUGUGGUGUUUGAACCUAGUAGUGAAUGGCCCAAGGAAAAAAAUACUGCAGGAAAUAUAGUAAUAGAUGAAUUUGGAUAAAGGGUAUAUGAGUGUUUUGGAGUAUUAUUCUUACAACUUCUCUGCAAGUUUAAAAUGAUAAUCUAAAUUUUAAAAACUUAUUUUCCGUUCAUCAAACUACUCUUAAAAUGUGUAAAACUAUACCUGAAUUUAAAAGCAACAAAACUCAUAUUGCAAGUCUUGGCAAACUGAGAGAUAGGAGCAGAAAACAAUGGUGGAUGCCUAUAAACGGAUCAAGAAAAGGGAGUGAGAAUUUACUGGAAAGAAGGACAAAUGAGCAUCGAAUUCAGCAGGUUUGGGUUUUUCCAGAGAUCAGUGCCUGAUACUGGUUCCCAGAUGAUAUCUCCCAAGAGCCCGGUUCCCAGGGUGUGUUCCAGCCUCUGUCCGCCAGGCUUCCCACCAAGUCUUGUGCCAAUAGUAGUUGCCAGCACAUUCUGCCUCACAAGUUGCUGGCUCCACCACUACUACCCUAUCCCACCUACGUCCAAGAUACGCAUCUGGCUUUUCUGCUUUGAAUUCAGCAAGUCAUCUCCUUUCCUGUCAUGUAACUCCCUCUGUGACUCGGCCUACCCAGCCACACUCCUCAGUGCUUUGUGGCAAAACUCAACCUGACCCCCCUUCAGAGAAAGAGAAAUAAGUGUCGGGGUUGAAGGUUCAGCUGUAAAGUGAUGUUUCCCAUACUCAUAAACUUACAUAGCAAUGAGGAACUGGAGUCUAUUUUUGACUGUUGUAGUGACCUUUGUGCAUACCCUAAAAGACAGAGGAACAUUGAGCUAAUGUAGCCAUCCCAUGAAGCCUCAGUAGCUCUAAUAGGUCCUUUUAGUUGUUGCUAGGGUGCCAGUUCUUGCACUUUAAUACAAUUCUUGGCUGGGCACCAUGGCUCACGACUGUAAUCCCAGCACUUUGGGAGGCCAAGGCAGGAGGAUCACUGGAGGCCAGGAGUUCAAGACCACCCUGGGCAACAUAGCAAGACCUCAUCUCUGCAAGGUAAAAAAAUUAACUGAGUGUGGUGGUUCAUGCCUAUAAUCCCAGCUACUCAGGCGAUGGGAGGAUCCCUUAAGCCCAGGAGUUGGAGACUGCAGUUAGCCAAGAUUGCGCCACUACCCUCCAGCCUGGGUGACAGAGCAAGACUCUGCCUCAAAAACCGACCAGCCAAACAAACAAACAAAAAAUGCAAUUUCUCCCAUCCUAACUCUUCAUAUUAGUAAAUCUUCAAUAAAAUGUAUAUGGGAAAUCAAUAUGGCACCCUCAAACCUAGUUGUAAUAGUCAGGAGAAGACCAUUCUAGCCUUUAAAAUCAGUCCUGUUAAAAAAAAAAUCAGUCCUAUUGACAUCAACGUUUUUACCUCCAGUUCCUCUCCACCCUUCUCUACCUCCUGAUUUCAUGUAGGCGAGCAAUUUAGGACAAUGAGAGUCACAGGAUUUUAAAUAACUUAAUUCCUAGGUGUGUUUGGUACGGAAACAAAGAUAACCCUGUUCAACAGUGAAUUUGUGCCCCUGGGUGAACGGCCAGGUGUUCUUUCAACUGAACUGUGAGACUAAUUUCUUCCUGGCCUCUGGAAACCAGCUGAAGCAGUGGGCCAGCUGGUCUAUCUUCAAUCUUGCAUACCAACAUCUUUCUCUGAUUCACAGAUUUCCUUUAUCCCCAGCACUUCCUCUGGUAUGUGCAUCCCCGAAAGUAAGUGAUAUCUAUUAUUGGAUUUGGGCGUUUUAAAAUCAUUAGCCUUCUGGAGGGGAGGGGAGAGGAAGGAGGCUGGAUGGUUACAUUAGAAUAUUUCCAGAGGGAACCUCACUUUAAUCUCAUCCACCUCUGACUUCUGCACCCCAGAUAACCCCCAUAUUUGGGAGGGAUGACAUCACAGUAACUGACAAUGGAAUUAUCACCAUUGCUCUUUUUAAUAUUUAAAUGAUACACAGACUCAGAGAAAACAAAAUGAGUUUACAUAUAGUCAUAAUAUCCAUAACUAGAGAUAUAAAACAAAAAGCUAUGGAGAUUCUUAUCUAGUGAAGAAAUCUCUUUUAGAAAGUUUCUGAUGACUUUCAGUUGCAAAGCAUAGCUCUUUCACAAUAUAUCAACCCACUUUCAAUGAUUUGAGAUUUGGAGAGGGCCCAGCCAUAGAUUUACCUGGUGAGUCACAGAGUAGAACUUGAUAUGAGAAAGCAGGACCCUAUAUCUAUCAGCCUAAUGGUUCUCAGAAUACCAGGUCAUAUCCAUCAUUUCUUUUCCCAAAUAGCUGUAACAGGCAUACCUCGUUUUACUGGGCUUCACUUUCUUGUGUUUUGGAGAUGGUAUGUCUUUACAAACUGAAAGUUUGUAGAAACCUGCAUUGAGUAAGUCUACCAGUGCCAUUUUUUCAACAACAUGUGCUCACUUCGUGUCUCUGUCACAUUUUAGUAAUUCUUGCAAUCUUUCAAAAGUAUUUAUUAAGAUAAAAAACAAAAGAAACGAUAUAAAAAUAAAGAGAAAAAGGAAGAAAAUUUGUUAUUAUUAUACCUGUCAUAGUGACCUGUGAUCCGUGAUCUUUCAUAUUACUAUUGUAAUUGUUUUGGGGCACAAUGACCCUCAUCCAUAUAAGAUGGUGAACAUAAUAAAUGUUGUGUGUGUUCUGAGUGAUCCACCAACCUGCCAUUCCUUCAUCUCUCUCCCUCUCCUCAGGCUUCCCUAUUCCUUGAGACACAACAGUAUUGAAAUUAAUUAAUAAAGUUAUAGCGUCCUCCAAGUGUUCAAGUGAAAGGAAGAGUUGCACAUCUCUCACUGUAAUUCAAAAGCUAGAAAUGAUUAAGCUUAGUGAGGAAGGCAUAUCAAAAGCAAAGACAGUCUGAAAACCAAGACUUUUGUGCCAAAUAGCCAAGUUGUGAAUGCAGAGAGAAAGAUCCUGCACCAAAUUAAAAUGUGACUCCAGUGAACACAUGAAUGAUAAGAAAGGGAAAAACAGCCUUGCUGAUACGGAGAGAGUUUGAGUGGUCUGGAUAGAAGAUCAAACCAGCCACAACAUUCCCUAAUGUUUGUAAGCCAAAGCCUAAUCCAGAGCAAAGCCCUAAAUCUUCAAUUCUAUGAAGGCUGAGAGAAGUGAGAAACUGCAGAAGAAAAGUUGAAAGGUAGCAGAGGAUGGUUCAUGAGAUUUAAGAAAAGAAACUGUCUCCAUAACAUAAGUGCAAGAUGAAGCAGCAAGUGCUGAUACAGAGGCUGCAGCAAGCUAUCCAGAAGAUCUAGCUAAGGUCAUUGAUGAAAUGGUUGCACCAAACAGCAGAUUUUCAAUGUAGACAACCUUCUAUUGGAAGAAGAUGCCAUGUAGCAUUUUUAUAGCUAGAGGAGAAGUCAAUGCCUGACCUCAAAGCUUCACAGGACAGGCUUACUCUCUUUUUAGGGGCUAAUAUAGCUGGUAACUUUAAGUCGAAGCUAUUGCUCAUUUACCGUUCUGAAAAUCCUAGGGCACUUAAGAAUUAUGCUAAAUCUAUUCUGCCUGUGCUCUAUAAAUGGAACAACAAAGCCUGAAUGAUAGCACAUCUGUUUAUAGUAUGGUUUACUGAAUAUUUUAAGCCCAUUGUUGAGACCUCCUUCUCAGAAAAAAAAAAAAAGAUUCCUUUCAAAAUAUCAGUGCUCAUUGACAAUGCAUGUGGUCACCCAAGAGCUCUGAUGGAGAUAAAUGAGAUUAAUGUUGUUUUCAUGCCUGCUAACACAACACCCAUUCUACAGCCCAUGGGUCAAGGAGUAAUUUCUGCUGUUAAGCCCUAUUAUUUAAGAAACACAUUUUGUAAAGCUAUAGCUGGCAUUCCUCUGAUAAAUCUGGGAAGGAUAAUUGAAAACCUUCUGGGAAGGAUUCACCAUUCUAGACACUGUUAAGAAAAUUCAUGAUUCAUGGGAGGAAGUCAAAAUAUCAGCAUUAACAGGAGUUUGGGAGAAGUUGAUUCCAACCCUCACGGAUGACUUUGAGGGGCUUAAGACUUCAGUGGAGGAAGUUACUGCAGAUGCGGUGGAAAUAGCAAAAGAACUAGACUCGUAAAUGGAGCCUGAAGAUGUGAUUGAAUUGCAUAAUCUCAUGAUCAAACUUAACAGAUAAGUAGUUGCUUCUUAUGGAUCAGCAAAGUGUUUUUUUUUUUUUUUGAGAUAGAAUCUACUCUUGGUGAAGAUACUGUGAACAAUGUUGGAAUAAUAACAAAGGAUGUUGAAUCUUACAUAAACCGAGUUGAUGAAGCAGUAGCAAGGUUUGAGAGGAUUGACUCCAAUUUUGCAAGAAGUAAAAUUGUGAGUAAAAUGCUAUCAAACAGCAUUGCAUGCUACAGAGAAAUCUGUCAUGAAAGGAAGAGUCAACUGUUGCAGCCACCUUCAUUGUCUUAUUUUAAGAAAUUGCCACAACCAGCCCAGCCUUCAACAACCACCACCCCAAUCCAUCAGCAGCCAUCACUGUUAAGGCAAAACAAUUGUGACUUGCUAAAGGCUCAGAUAAUUGUUAGCAUUUUUUAGCAAUCGAGUAUUUUUAAGUAUGUACAUCGUUUUUUACACUAUAUUGUAGUCUGCUAUGCAUGCAAUAGCAUUAUGUCUAAAAAACAUAAUUUUUAUAUGCACUGGGAAGCCAAAAAAUUCACGUGAGCUACUUUAUUGCUAUAUUUAUUGUGGUGGUCUGGAACUGAACCUGCAAUAUUGUCAAUGUGUGCCUGUAUAAGAUUCUCCAUGCACUAAAAAGGACAUUUGAAAGUCAUGAGUAAGUUGUAGAGGAACUCUGGUGACUUGAAGCUUGUUUACUUUUAGCAGUGUGUACCUGUUGACACUUCUAGUAUAAUUUAUAUUCUUUCUCUCAUGAGUAUUUUACAGGAAAUGCGUUUUCCUUUGCUAGUGAUAUAUGCACUUUGGUUUUCAGGAAGCUGUGGUGCUUUGGUUGAAGCUCUCUGUCUGUUUUAGAGAAAAGACUUACAAUGACCUCCUGAUAUAGUUUGGAUAUUUGUCUGCUCCAAAUCUCAUAUUGAAAUUUGAUCCCCAAUUUUAGAGGUAGGAUAUAGUGAGAGGUGUGUGGGUUAUGGAGGCAGAUCCCUCAUGGACAACUUGGUUCUGUCCUCUGGGUAAUGAGUGACUUCUCACUCUAUUAGUUUUUGUGAGAGCUGACUUUUGAAAAGAGCCUGGCACCUUCCUCCCCUCUCUCUCUCUUGCUUCCUUUCUCUCUCUCCGUGUGAUGCCUGCUUCUCUUUGCCUUCCACCAUGAGUGGAAGCUUCCUGAGGCCCUCAGCAGAAGCUGAUGCUGGUGUCCUGUUUCUUGUACAGCUUGUAGAACUGUGAGCCAAAUAAACUUCUUUUUUUAUAAAUUACCCAGCCUCGGGUGUUCCUUCAUAGCAAGGCAGACAGUCUAGGACACCCCCCAAAUGUGAGCUGCACCAUAAGGCAAACUGGGAAACCUCCUUUAGUUUUGCAUAUGUGAGAAUUUUGAUUGACUGAACCAAGGAAUCACCCUCCUAACUCCACUGCAGAAGGCCAUUCUCAUGUCAUUUGCACACGUUUAGCUUGCCUGAAGUGUGUUCUAUAAAAUGCACCCAGAUUUUCAGGCAUUUAAAAUUAUUAUUAUUUUAAAUCUCCUACUUUCUCUCUCUCUCUCUUUUUUUUUUUUUUUUUUUUUUUGAGAUGGGGUCUUGCCCUGUCAUCCAGUCUGGAGUGCAGUAGUGCAAUCACAGCUCGCUUCAGCCUCCAACUCCUAGCCCCAAGCAAUCCUCCUGCCUCAGCCUCUCAAGUAGCUAGGACUAUAGGUACACACCACUGCACCUGGCUAAUUAAAUUUUUUUUUUCUUUUUAGAGACAUGGUCUCACUCUAGGUCUUGCCUAGGCUGUUCUCAAACUCCUGGCCUCAAAAGAUCCUCCUGCCUCAGCUUCCUAAAGUGCUGGGAUUGCAGGCAUGAGCCACCAUGCCCAGUUGCAUGUUUUAAUGGAGAGAGAUGUCCUGGGCAUUUGAACUGCAGAUUCCCUUAAACUGGACAUUGUCAGCUAUUUAUGUAUUACAAAAACAAUUGUGUUUCAUGUAAAGUAUUAAACAUCAACAUUACGUCACCACAAGGGUGAUUACAGCAACCUUCACUCCUAAGUGUGCGUCACCUACACAAACAGAGUUGUUUGUCUGCAGCAUUGUUUUCAUUUGGUAACAAUUGUAAGAGUUGAAGUAGCACCUUAAGGAGUAAUUUUCAGAGGUGAAGCAAUCAGUUUUCAAAAGUGAACUCCUUAUAGUUAAUAACUAACCAAUAAAAAAAUAAAGCUAUCUCCAUGGCACAAAUGCCCAUGGCACAAAUGCCCAUGGCAAAAGGAAAUAAGACGAGUCGUUUUAAAAGGUAGCUUUGAAAAACAAAAAAGGAUUUAAAAUUCAAAGACUUUGGGAAAAUUCAACUUAACCAAUAACAUGAGUAACGACUAUUACUAUUUCCUGAGUCCUUACCAUAUGCCAAAUACCGUUGUACAUUGUACCUGCUUCACAUAAAUUAUUUCAUCUCAUUCUCACAACAUUCUGUGAAGCGCGGGUACUUUAUUAUCUAUCCCUGUUUGCCAGAUAAGGAAGCUGAGACUUCAUACAGUGACUUACAAGUUCGGACAGCCUCCAGCAAACACAGGAAACAGGAUUCGAACCCAUGCAGUCUGCCUCAGAGCCAAAGCCCUUGGCCAUUUUUCUAUCCUGCCUUCCACAGAUCAUUUCUGCCUACAGCAGAGGUCAGAAACUGACAACCGGCUGGCCUUACCUAGCCUUAGGUAACAGUAAUGGCUAUUGAACACUUACUAUGUGUCAGGAUUAUUUUACACACAUUCAUGUGUUCCUUCAUUUAAUCUUCAAAGCAACUCCAUGAGGUAGGUGGCAGUUAUUAUCCCCAUUUUACAGAUGAGAAAACUGAGACCAAGAGGAAGUAACACUUCCCAAAUGUUAGCAGAACUAACAUCCAAAUCCAGACUGUCUCAUUCCAGAAUCCCCUCCUCUUCACCAUUAUGCUAAAAAUACAGUUGUCUGCCAACAUGACAAACCUGGAUGUUUCCCCAGAAAAUGAAGGCUUCUGACUUGUCAUGAAAAAAAAAAAAAAAAAAAAAAACUGGAAGACUUGUCCUCUUGGACCGAGCAACAGUCACUUGUAACAAUGGGCAGCUGCCCAUUUUAGAUGAGGUAUCUCCUACCUAGUUGCUACCACCCCUCAUUUAGGCUGCUUUGCUCUUUGAUUGCCGGUCUGAACUUUGGGGACAUUCUAUUUUGCAGUCUCAGUCUAAGGUAUCCUUAAUACUGGAUCUGCCUCACUUAACAAGCUAAAUGUCUGUGUGUUUUAUGUUUUUUAUUGUAGCACAAGUUGUUUAAUGUUCUCUAAAAAGCAUUCCCCACAAAUAGCAGUAAAUGCCUCUUUCCUAUUUUCUUCCCUGUCCCUUGCCCCGAAAGUAAGGCAGCUCUGCAGAACUAGUAUUUGUGCCCAACGAAGUGGGAAGAUAUGAGGCUGAUAGCCUUUUCUCUCUCUUCUUGGUUGGUGGCACUCUGGUAGUGCUUGGUUAGCGAUAAUGGAGCAUCUCAUGGCUUUGUUAUGUGUCAUAGUAGGCUAUUGUGUGACAUAGAGACACCUGGCUUUUGUACACGCCAGAGCAAAAUUCAACUACAACAUCCAGAAUUGAAGAGAAGGAUAUUGGCAGGUACAUGCCUCCUUCUCAAACCAGAGAUUUAUAUAUUUAAAAAGGGCUUUUCUAAGAACUCAAUCUUGAUUAUUUGUUCCAUGUUGGGCCAAACCAGUGCAUUAUUGGGAAGAUAAUGAGUGGCAUUCACCCAAGGGUAAUCCUUUCAGGGAUUUUGAUGAUGCAGUAAAUCAUGAGUGUAAAGCCUGAGUGGUUUAUGCCAUUAAAACCUCAAGAUAGAAUUAGACUUGUAAUCACCACUUGCCCAUGUUUUGUCAUUUAUGAUAAUUAUAGUAGUAAUAAUCCAUGUAUUGUUGAGAAGUAGCAGUCAGAAGCAUCCAUCAAUUUUUUAUCGACACCAAAUCAAGUUGAUACUUCAUCUUUGCUGCAGAAAUGUAGAUUGAACCAAUUAGUCUAAAGAAAUUGGGCAGUCAUUAACAAUGAAGCAAGCAGUUAAUCUACAGAACAUUUCUGGCCCCUCUGAUGCCAACAAUUCCUCUUAAUUAUGUGGAAUAUCAUGAGCUUCUUUGGGACUCUGUCAACAGUGCCAUUGUUGGCUUACAUUAGAAGGAGCAUCUAUGUCCCUGCUUUUAUUUAAAAGAAUGCAGUGCCUUCCAGCCCCCACCUUGCACUCUUAGGCGCUUCUAGGCAAAUGUAUUCUGAAGCAGAACACUUGAAUCAAAGCACUUCGCAUUUUCUUUCUUAUUUAGAAAUAAGAAUUUUCCCCAAUGGGCUUCUUUCGGUGAUGGCACGUUAGCUCACCAUCCCAUAUGUGUUAACUAUUUUUGUUCACCUUACCCAAAUCAUGGAAUAAUCAUCUCCUUUUAAAAAAGGAAAGAAAAGAAAAGUCAGAGUUUAAAAGAAAAAUCCAACUAUUUGUGAAGAAAUCCUGGUGCUAAUGAGCUUUCUGCAUCUGCCUCAAGUCUUUUCCCCAGGCUAGCCCAGUCUCCCUCUCUAGACAUUUUCAAUCAGCCUCGCCCGCAAAUUGUACUAAGCAGCUGAAUAAUGCAGGGUAGAAAUUUCAAAUAUAAAUAUUAUUUCCUAUUUAGGAAAUUUGGAAAAGAAAGCAGGAAAAAAAUAACUCACCCCCUGGUCCCCCACCAUGACACUACCUCUGUGAACAUUUUGGUAGAUAUUCUUUGGGCUCUGACACGUACACACAUGUUGACUUUUAUCAUCAUCAUCAUCAUCAUCAUUAUUCUAGUACUCUCUUUUUCACUUUGCUAAAGUUUGAAUCAUCUUUUGUAAUGGAUGCGUAAUACUCUACCAAAUAUAGAGUAUGUAUUUGUCCAUGUUUUGAAUUAUUUCCCUAGGAGAGCUUACCCAAGGUAAAAUACUUGGUCAAAAUUUAUAAGCCUCUUCAUAGCUCUUGGUACAUACUGACAAACUCUCUCCAAAAGGAUGGUACCAAUUUUUAAAAUCUCACCAGUAAUAUAUGCAGAUACUGGUUUGAUGUUAUUGAGAUUUAAAUUCAGUUGUGUUGGCAUGGUUAUAGCUUAGAUAGAUAGAUGAUAGAUAGAUAGAUAGAUAGAUAGAUACAUACAUACAUACAUACAUACAUACAUACAUACAUACAUUCAUUCAUGUGUUUGUGUGUGUGUAUGUGUGUGUUACUCCUCCUUAAUGGACAAAUGGUGAUAUGGAUUGGCUGUGUCCCCACCCAAAUCUCAUCUUGAAUUAUAGUUCCCAUAAUCCCCACGUGUGAUGGGAGAGACCCAGUGGGAGGUAAUUGAAUCAUGGGGGUGGUUCCCCCAUGCUAGUCUCGUGAUAGUGAGUAAAUUCUCAUGAGAUCUGAUGGUUUUAUAAGGGGCUUCCCCCUUUACUGGGUUCUCAUUCUUCUGCUUCCUGCUGUCAUGUGAAGAAGAAUGUGUUUGCUUCCCCUUCUGCCAUGAUUGUAAGUUUCCUGAGGCCUCCCAAGUCCUGUGGAACUGAGUCAAUUAAACCUCUUUCCUUUAUAAUUUACCCAGUUUUGGCCGUUCUCUAUAGCACUGUGAGAAUGGACUAAUACAAUGGGCACAGUAUCAAAUUGUACCCUGACUCAAAUUACUGUAAACAAUGCCAGUUGUUAUCUCACAUCACAGGAAGUUCGGAAAUAGGACAGCUGUAGGUGUGAUAUGAUCAUAGGCCCAAUGAUGCGAUUGGAGACUUGAGUUCUUUUCUUCAGUUUCUGCCAUCAUCACCACCCUCAUGCUGGCCUCCUUUGGGCUUCAAAUGCCUACAGUAGCUCCAGGCACCACAUCCAGAUGUAGAAACAACAGAGAUAGAAGGAAAUCAAUUCUUCUUGUGUCUCCUUCUUAAGAGUGAGGAGAUCCUUCCUAGAAGCUCCCAACUGAAACCCCUAAACCAAGACUGGCAAGGGAAAUGGAAGCACCAUUAUCGACUGAUUAACUAAGAUUUACUCCCAAUCUGGCAAUGGAGUCAACUUCCUUUGAGUGCUGAAUACCUGAAUAAAAUAGAUUCUGUUAACAAGGAAGAAGGUGGGAAUGGUUGUUGAGGCACCAACAGUGCCUCCCAUAGGCAUCAUGAUUUUUUUAUGCCUCUGCCAUACUCAUAGAACCAUAUACAUUUCUUUAGUAACAGUUGAUGCAUUUAAUGGGCAUAUGCAAAAGUUGUUGGCAUAUCUACCAAGUACUGGGCUUUGUCCAAUGUGGAAGGUCCUCCCAGGUAGUGAUCAUCCUCCACAAUUCCUUUACAUUUUCCUAAAAACCUAUCUCAGUGUUGGGCCCUUCAGGUAGAAACCAGGAACACCUCGGUUUCUAGAUUCCUUUGGCAUAUAGGUUUCCUAUGGGAAAGAAAUAGGAGAGCUGGCUUUCCUCUUUGAGAAUCUUCUGUUUGGUGGAGAUUUGACAUCCAGGAUACCAUUGUUAGGACUUCCACUGAGAUGAAAGUUUACAGCCUGAUGAAACAAGUCUCACUUUCCACUUUGAAUUACUCAGGCUCUGUGCAUCUCUUUCCACUGCACAGCGUAGCAUUUUGAACACUUCACUACUCAUUAGCACCUCCAGUGAGAGAUCAGAAAAGAAGGUGGCUGGGAGGGGAGGAUUGAAGAAUGCAGAUUAGUCAAAUUGUUUUUUGUUUUAUCUAGUUAGAGAAACAGCUGAAAUUACUGCCUCAAAAAAAUUUGGAAAAUUAUCUGGCUUAUAGUUUAUUUCUAUAGUUAUUUUCCCACUAAUUGUAAAAAUUAGGAGUAUUACAUUUUAGAGUAAAAUAAUAAAUAAACAAUAACAAAAAAUGGCUACAACAGAAGAAAACAUGUUCCUGGAUUGAAGAAACCAACCUAGAAAUUAUACUGUAUGCCUCAGAAAUUUAAUACUAUUUUGUCUUUCCUGUAUGCAGUUGGAUUAUAGAGUACAGAUAUUGUCUCUUUAUUAAUGCAUGAUUUAUAAAUAUUAUUUGACACUAGGGAUAUCAAAGUGAUUGUGGAUCAAAGCUGCCCAUCCCUUCACCCUGGUAGAUGAGAACACAAAAUAUAUCCAUUUCCUAUACACCAUGAAGACAUUGCUUCCAGUAGGUUUUCUUGCUGGAGACAAAAAGAAAAACAGAAGCACCUACUGUACUUGUGCACUUUCUGUUUUACAGUUUCAUAAGGAUUUUUACAACAUAAGUACAUGCUCUAUGAUAUUACAUACCUUUCCACCACUUAUAUAAUCAAGUGCAAUUAUACUGACUGCUUGAAUAGAUGAUGGGAAAAAUGACUUGAAUCAAAAAUUACACAACAGAACGCUGUUUCAGAAAGGCUUUUGGAGUGUACGUGCCACAGACCCCAAAAAGAGAUGGAUCAAGAUGAUUAUAAUAGCCUUGAAUUUUCCUAGGUUGGUUGAGUGUGGUGGCUCAUGCCUGUAAUCCCAGCACUUUGAAAGGCUGAGGCAGGCGGAUUACUUGAGGUCAGGAGUUCGAGUCCAGCCUGGCCAACAUGGCGAAACUUCAUCUCUACUAACAAUACAAAAAUUAGCUGGGCAUGGUGGCACAUGCCUGUAAUCCCAGCUACUUGGGAGGCUGAGCAGGAGAAUCCCUUGAAUCUGGGAGACAGAGGUUGCAGUGAGUCAAGAUGGCACCACUGUACUCCAGCUUGGGCAACAGAGUGAGACUUUGUCUCAAAAAAAGAAAAAAAAAGAAUUUUCCUAGGUUAUGGCACCAAGAAUAACUUGUACCAUUUUGGAAGAUUCAUCUUUUUUCCCACAUAACACAAUGUAGCAUGUAGUAUAUGUGACACAUACCAUAGCUACCUGUGCAGGAGCUUGGUGAGUUCUGGUUUUGUCUUUCUUCCCCUCAAUUUCUAUCCCUUCUUUUCUUUGUGCUUCUUCCACUCUCCUCUUUCUAUUCUUCUACCAUCCUCAUCUUUUCAUUUAGAGGCUUGGAGAAGAGCUUAAAACAAUAGGUGAUGGGGAGAAAUGUAGUUUCUUCAUGCAACAUAAUUUCCCCCUGCAGUAAUCCAUGGAUCAACACAUUUGAGGGCAGCUGGUUUAGAAGAGGCCCUUACAAUUGUCUUAACUUACUCCUCAGAGGGUAGGCUGGGUGUAUAGCCUACAUGGCUAUACAUGGCCAUGUAGGCCAUGUAGGCCAUUAGAUUACAUGGCCUUUACAAGGAAUUUUUGGGUGGUUUUAUUGUUUGUUUGUUUGUUUGUUUGUUUUUGAGACAGAGUCUCCCUCUGUCACCCAGGCAGGAGUGCAGUGUCGCAAUCUCGGCUCACUGCAACCUCCGCCUCCUGGGUUCAAGCAAUUCUCCUGCCUCAGCCUCCUGAGUAGCUGGGACUACAGGAGCACACUAUCACACCCAGCCAAUUUUUGUAUUUUUAGUGGAGACAGGAUUUCCCCAUGUUGGUCAGGCUGGUCUCGAACUCCUGACCUCAUGAUCCGCCUGCCUUGGCCUCCCAAAGUGCCAAGAUUACAGGUGUGAGCCACCGCGCCUGGCUUGGGUGGUGUGAUUCUUAUGUAGGAGAAAAAAGAGGAACAUAAAUGCAGAACACAAUUAUGCAAAAUUAGGAGCCUUUAAAAUGAAAUAUGAUAUUGUAGGUAGUUUCUUCAAAACAACAUACUAGUUUUUUAUACUUGUUUAUUCAUCACUGAAAACAAAACAUAUGGAAAAGGCAAUUUUUCUCCCAGCCAACCCCUUUUCCUCGGAUAUUUUUUCAAGAAAAAUUUUACAGCAGAUGUUUUCAAAUAGAUUUCUAUUUAUUUGUGGGCUACCAUUAUAUCAGUAGGAUUUCUCUAGAACCUUUCCAUCACUUCACCUGAGUUUUCUUUAUCGGAAGAAAAAAACAAAAAAACAAAAAGAAAUGUCUGAUCACCUGCCCUAAGUCUACAGUUGAGAGCAGUUUUGGGGACUAGUAAGUCAUGUUCUCUUAAGGACAGCGUCUCCUAGGUGAGCGGCUCGUAGUCCAUAUGGAGCAAAUUAGACAGUGAAAGAAUGGUGCUGCUACUGUUUCUGAUUGGUUACGGUAGUAUUAAAAAAGAACAACAACCGACUUGCCCAGCUCUGAAGAAGAAAGAUGGAUAAAAUGCUCUUUGAACACACUAGUCUUUUUUUUUUAAUGUCUGUACAGAAGGGUUGCAUUUAUAUUUGGCUUUCCAGACCUGUCUCUUGACCUUCUAAUUACUUUAUUUGAAACAGCAGUGAGGGUAUAAUAAACCUGGAGGUUGUCUCUCCUUUGCUUUAUCAUAAAUUAAAGCUGCUGGUUUGUUGAGGUGAAAGUGGAGGCUGAAUGUUCAUUACUGCUCAAGUGACGGCUUGUCAAUAGCAGUGCUUUUUAGUUUGUUCUAGUCAGCACUUGCUGUGCAUUUUGUUGGACCACUGGGAAAUAAAUACAACAAGAUUAUACAUUUGGAAUACCACAAGAGUUCACAAAAAAAACCACAAAUGAUAAAUUAUACACUUGGUAGAAAGUGACAUGCUAUCUUGUGCUAUUAACAACCAAAGAUAAUUGCAACGAAUUGUAAUUGCAGUUUGCAACUUACAGUACAGUGUGUCCAACAUCAAUCUUAAUAGUGAACAAAGCAAUUUAUAUUAAAACUUAAUUCACUUGGUAACUUUCCGCUGUAUACACGGGAGCUAACAGAUGUAGCUUUUCAGAAAGUUCAAAGGCAUUUGAAACGUGGAGAGAAAUGCUAAUGCAGUAAGCCUUGGAGAAAUAUUGCAUUACUACUUGUAAUGAAAACAAAUGUAUGUCAUUAUCUCCUAGUUUGUGUUUAUUUAAUAAAAUAUGCAGUUUGCACAUUGGUGAAUUCAGUGUUUCUGAAUGGAUAUGGAAUAAUGUUCUGUUCAGAAUCAAAGGCCAAACAGGACUAGCAAUUACGCAUCUUCUGUAAAUAGUCUGCUGUAGCAUGCACCUUGAUGCUUGAGUGGGUUUUGUAUGAGGUGUAACAGCAAACCGGGGUAACUUUAUUCAUGACUUUCCUUAGAUUGGAUGUCUUUGAAGCAAGAAAGGGAGAUCUCCUGGAAUUACUUAAGAGAACAAGCAUAUUUGUUUUGUGAGCUUGACUGAUGGCCGGUAGAGCAGUUGAGUGAAAUCUCUAAACUGAUUAGGGCUUUCGUUCAAAUAAUCUUCUACCGUUUUCAUUAAUUUAUUCCUUAAUGCUAUUUUGCUGCUCUUCUACCAAGGAUAAUAAUCUCACACUCGCUGACCUCCAUGAGUGGAUGACCUGGAGCUCAUAACUAAUCUUAUUUACUCUUCUGACCAGCCCAACUUCAUUUACCUUGACUGGAUAAAGAGCCUUCCGUUGCUAAGCCUCCGUUCCUUCGUAGCAUUCUCGUUAAUCUACAGUGAAGGGGGAACGAUGGGCUUUCCCAAUCAAGAUCCCAAAGCAUGCUGGGGCACUGGGAACUUCGUGCGAUUUCUCUUCCUUUCUUGAAAACAUGUUUCCACUUUAUUGUUCCCCCUUUUUGAUUUGAAAAUAAUAGAGAAAAAUGGGGGAGUGGGACUUCACCAUGGUCCCACUCUCCUAAUACAGCUAUUUUUACCUUGAAAGUUAAUUUCCAGCCAUUGACCAUAGGAAUGUGUGGGUUAAUUUAGGUAUUGUUGUUGAGUACAUGAAAUUUUGUAUCAUGCUUUUUUAUUUAAUGCUACAUUGUUUCCUGUGUUGCUUCAUAAUUUUAUAAUUAUGCAUUUUAAAGACUGAUAAUGCGUUGUUUAUAUACUAUUUUGGGUUUAAUUGUUCCCCAGUAUUGAAGUUAGGUUACUUCUACUUAGUUAUGCUAUUAGGAAUAAUGCUGCAAUAAAAAUCUCUGUUUUCUUCAA